CUCCUACCAUACAUUCUAUCAGUGAGUGACUUAUGAUUGAUGGGAACCACGGCUUGUUGUUUAGCUUUAUCUGUGACCUCAGCGAAUGGACAACAGGAAUUUCCAGGCUGUUAAAUUCCCUGAAUGCUUGAAGACAGGGGCUCACGGUGUUGCUCAAGGCAGGUAGCAGAGUGAUAUUAUUCUCCAGCGAUGAUGGGGGAGGGACGAGAGAAGAAAGGGGAGGGAGAAGGAGGGGAAGGGAGGGGGAAUUCCUUUUGUGAACAGCAGCAAUUCUGGCUCAGUUUGUUUCUUAGCCCUCCUCCAUGGCUGUGUGUGGGGAAAGGUGCAUUUCCUGGACCUAAAGAAGCUGGCAGUCAGAACCUUGCCAUGGGCUGCGCAGAGUAACUCCAUGGGGUUGACUGGAGAAGGCACUGAGUUUUCUUCAAUUAGUUAAGAUUUUGUUUUCCAAAUCAGUUAGAUUGGUCCAUGAGCAACUGGACUAUUACAAUCCUGUAUAAAAACAGAGAUUUUGAAUUUAAAGGUGUGCCAGCAUUCCUAGUGCUAUGUAGGAAUUUAGUGUCGUUUUUAAUCUCUAUAUGCUUGGGUAUCUAUCUGGAGGUGAUUUUGAAAGUUAACGUGCACCUCUUAUCAGCAUGCUUUGAGGAGCAGAGCAGUGCAUUUGUGUAUGUGUGUGAAAAUGCAUUAUAACUGAAUGCACAAAAAUGUUUUCUCAUUGUCUUGCUUUUUCCCCACCUCUUUCUUACACACGUGUGAAUAAGGUUCCUGAACUGGAUGUAGUGAGAUUUAGUCACUAGCAUCAGCAGCUACAUUUGCUUUUGGAUAACGGUGUCCAUCUCCCAAACUUUUUUGCUAGUCUGUCUUCCUAACUCCUCCUUUUCUUUCUCUUCCUCUUCUUUCUCUUCCUGUCUCUAUCCUUACCCUAUGCUACUUUGUUUGCAAAAGUAAUUCUUGAGCUUUUGCUGAGUUAAGGAGACAAGGUUCUCUUCUGAUGUGAAUGAAACGACAUCAUUCUAGGUGUGAAUGAAACGACACUGGUUUGUCGAUGUUUGUUUAGUCUACCUUUUCAGCGAUUAUUUUGUUCUUUUUUUUUUAAAUGACAAUUAGGCAAAAUUAAAACACUCCUUUUAGUGUAAUAGGAUUACAUCAUUCACACAUUUAGGCAAAAUUGAUUUUCUGAUCUUCUAAGGCUAUUUUUUUAAAGACACUUAUUGAUUUGGCUUACCAAGUUUUAUUCCUUUUUUUUUUCCAGAACAAAGGCAUAUUCCCUUAAUGUAAGAGAUCACCAAGGCUGCUUGUCACUGUAAUUAAUUUCUUAAUGGUUUCCCUCCUAGGAACCAAAUUAUGAGAUGCAUUCCAAGAUCCAGUACCCUCAAACAGAUAUUGUGUGUAGGAUAAAAAAGCCCUAGUGGAAAAAGAGAUUUUAAAACUUUUAUCUGUUUUACAAUUCUGUUAAGUGGGCAUGAACAUUCAUAAUUAUUUUUAUAGCCUCAUUUCAAAUCAGCUAACCUAAUGGUAAAAAUGUUUCACCCAUCAAGUCAUAUUAUUUCAAUUUUAGACAUUUAAAAUUCAAGGGAUUAAAGGAGAAAGAAAAAUGACUGUCACUAUAAAUGUUACCUACAAAAAAGAAAAACCUUCCUUUUGAAAACUUGCUUCUUGAGUAGCAGAAUGACUCAUGACAAGAAAUUUAUAAUUUGAAAUUUGCAAAAGAUAAAGCUCAGAGCUCUGUGAGUUUUGAGUUAUUAGUAGUUGAAUGAAUUAAGCCUUCACAAUGCAUCUAAUUAGAAAGAAAUUAUUAAAAUAUUGGUGAGAUCCAUUGUUUAUGUCGAUUUCAUUGUACUUUUCCUGAGGAGCUGCUGGAGACUAGCUUUACUUUCAUAAGCAUCACACUAUAUGAAAAAGUUUCAUUUGAGGGUUAGUUCAGAUGCUACUGUUCUUUGCCCUACGUUGUAAGGGAUGUUAUUAGAAGCUAUAAAAUUCUUCUCCCUUUCUUUAAAAUGUAUUUGCACUUUUAUGUGUAGGAGUGUGAGGGCAGAAGUAAACAUGUAGGAGGGUUAUGUAUUCUUCAUUAAAAAUAUAUUUCACAAAAGAUUAUAGUUUGUGUGGGAAGGAAAUAGCUGCUUGUCUGUUGAUUGCACUGUGCUUAUUCCAUAUAAGAACUAUUUGAAUUGAGUCAGGAUAACCUCAUUUUGAUAAUCUGAUGACUGCUUCUGCUUGGAGAAGAGAAUAUAAUUUCAAGGCUGCGUGCUGAUGGGCAACAGUAAUUGUUCUCUUUUUGGCAGAGCUUAGCAUGGAAUCUGCUUUGGUAUUUUUGUAACUACAUAUGCAAAUCUUUUCUCCCAAAGCUUUUCCCCCCUUUCUCUCUCCAUGUGCAGAGCUUUUUGUAAUCUUCAGGACUGUGAAAUUCCAAAGGUGUGAUAUCGAAUGCUAUCCGUGUAUGAUGAUGUGUAAACCUAAGUUAGAGCAAAAUCUUGGCUUGAAGUGAAGUCUUUUUGUUCAAGCAGAUCCUGUACUGUAAGCAGAUUUCCCUGUAUACUUGGUUUCUAUGGAGACACUUUUAUUACUUAUAGAUGAUCAGACUAUUUGAAUGUAGUAUGGGUGGUUAGUUUAUCAGCUUUGGUCAGUGCAGGUGAUGGAGUUUCCUGGUUAAUAUGUGGUCCUUUCACUAAGCUUCCUAUUGUGUUGCAGGGUUUAGGAGAGUGAAGCUAACACCAAAAACCAACCUAAAACAUUGAGGUAAUGUGACACUGAAUUUUACCUUCUUAAAGGUACAUUACGCCAGCGUUAUGUAAACGAUAAAGAGAAACCCUCAAAAUUAGGAAGAUUCCUAAUUGACACUGUCAGAACAAUGGAAUGACCCAUUGCUAAAGCUCAUUCUGAGAGGGAAUAUAUGAUUCUUUCUUUCUUUUCCCUCCCCUCCCCUCCCCCCCUUUCUGUUUUUUAUAGACAGAGUCUUGCUUUGUCACCCAGGCUGGAGUGCAGUGGCAUGAUCAUAACUCAUUGUAGCCUUGACUUCCUGAGCUCAAAUGAUCCUCCUGCCUCAGCCUCCUAAGUAGCUAGGACUACAGGUGCUCACUACCACUCCCGGCUAUUUAUUUAUUUAUUUUUUGUGGAAACAGGAUCUCACUGUGUUGGCCAGGCUGAUCUCAAACUCCUGGCCUCAAGUGAUCCUCUCACCUUGGCCUCCCAGCAUGCUGGGAUUACAGGCAUGAGCUACUGCCCUCUGCCUCUUCUACUUCUUUUCUAUGUAAUCAGUGAGUUAUCGGUAUUGAAGGACUCUUUAGCUUUAGGAAUUCUUCUUAGUGAUUAUCCAAGUUUUAAAAUGUUUCAUACUUCACUGUAGUCACCUUAUAGAUGAAGAAUAUAAGGCCUAAUAAAUGGAUGGGCUUUAUACUCAAAAUUACACAUUGUAUUGACAGUGGCUUAAGGAUAAGCUCUGCUCACUGGAGCUUGUCUGCUGGGGCUUAGGAGCUGAAAGGCUCUGACCUCGUAUAUAUGAUGUCAGGAGAGAGCGUGAUGACUCUGGGUAGAGUCCUCCUGCAGCCCUGAUAAUGGUAGCAAACUCUGAUAAUUAGGGCAGUGUUUACAGCUUUAACUGUGUUAUCUUAAUCUUCCUGUGACAGAGGUUGGCAGUGGCCAUCAGUAACUGAUGUGUAGAUCCACUGUGAGGCACUCAGAUUUCUAUAACAAGAUGUCAUCAUUUGAGUCAGCAGGACUAGAAGCUCAUGUUGAAUGGUGGCUUUUAGGAAGGACUUUCAUAGAGCAUGAGACUGGGAACUCAGCGAGAGACACAGAUCUCUGAGGAGGCAUAGUAUGUAGAGAUAAGUGCAUUUUAGUGGAAAUAUUUUAUUCUACUCUUUUUACUUGGAAGAAUAUACAUUUUCUAAGAGAGAAGGAGAUCUGUGAGGUCUAACUAUCCUGAUAGCUGAAAGCAGGACCUCAGAGACCAUAUUUUCGAAUACAGAUGACAGAACUCAGGUCCAAGACUUUUUAUUAAAGGCAUUCUUCUAACUUCACUAAAGUUAGAUGACACUAUCUGAUUGCCUCAGAACUAAAGGAUGCACAGGAAUGUACUCUAAUAACAUGUGUAGGGCCAUUCUUACUGUGUCUCAAAUCUGGUUGCUCUAGUUGUCUACAUUCAUUUUCUUGGAAUUAAUUCACUUGCUACAGAAUUAGUCUUAAAAAAUUCUCUUUCCAAACUUUUAAAUUUUUAACUGGACAUUUAAAAAUUAUUGACAUGAUGAUUUAUAGAUAUUUAAACAACUAAUUGCCCACAAGUGCCUAAUUUUCCAUAAAAUCACAGCCUGACUCGUGUGAACUGGAUAAGGCCAUAUCCAAAAUUGUUUCCUUCUGUUAUUUAGGUUAGUUUUAUAUGAGUGGAGAGGUAUUCAUAAGGCCACAUGGCAUAGUCCAAUAAAGAAUUUAUUUCCCUCCUGAGGGAACAAGCUUAAGAAGGUUCAGAAACAUACAGUAAAACCAUGAAAGAGGAUCUAUGCAUUUUAACCAUAAAGCAUAAGAUAAAAACUUAUUUCCUCAAGAAACUUGAGUCUAGUAUGGGGAAAAAAAAUGACAUUUCAUGCUUGAUCCAAACUGAGUACUAGAGAUGUUAAAGAUGCCUUACGUCUGAACCCCAGUGGUUCAAGGAAUGGAAAUGCCAGUAACUGAGACCAGAACUGCUGGGGAGAAGACACAUUUUAUUUUAUAUAACUGUUCUGUCGAGAUGAGGGUGUGAGGAACCUGCAGUUGUGAUUGUGGCCUCAAAUUGUGCCAAGGCAUUGAUGGAUGGAGGGAAUCUAGGAAGAGCCCAGUUGUAGGCCGAACUUUGCCUGGGGACUUGAUCAAAGAGAGUCUGAGCCACGCAGGCCAAAUGGACAGGUUUGGACUAGGAUCUCAGAGGUGUAGGGCAGCUUUCCCCGUUUGUAAUGAAGUGCUGAAGCAAACCUUUCUCUUGGAUAUGGAAGACUGUCUCAAAGAGAGGACACCGAAUGCCUUUAAAGGUAUAAAGCUCCCAGGCCUCAGAGAAUCUGGACUUUUAAAGGCAAGUAAUGAUCCCUGAGAAGAGAGGCUUCUUUGUCAUCAAUGUAGGACACGCUGGUGACUGUGUCUGGUGGCAAAGGCUUGCCUGUCAGUCCCACUUGAGGCUCAGCUGUCUCCACUGGGAGGGUCCAAUUCCUCUCUGACCUUUGUUCCUUCUCAUUGGAGUCAAUUUUUUUGGUGUGGCUUCACCAUCUGGGGGAGGGUGCAAGUUAUGGGGUUGUUGGCAGGAGCAUUGAAUUUGGGUCCUAGUGAGGGUGAAUAUCUGAAAUGUCUUGACAUUCUACUGUGUUUGCUGGUGGGAACUGUUCUCUGCUGGAGAGAGAGCAAAGAGAGAAUAUGAGAGCUGAGUUUAGAAUCCUGGGAAAUAUUCCUGCUUUGGGGACGAAUGAAUAAUAGAAUCUAAUAAAGAUGACUAAGAGGAGUAGUGAGGGGGUAGGUGGACGCCAAGAAAAGCACCAUUAUAGGAGAGAUGAAUUAUAGAGUUUCCAAAUUAUCAAUUUCAUUCACUGAAAUUGGUGUUCAAUUGAGGGUAUUCUAUAUGCCAGGUUCUAUGCUAGUCCCUGUAGAUACAAUAUGAACAAGACAUAGUCUUGGUCCUCAAAGAAUUCAUUGGAAGUCAGAGAUCAUGGCCCAUGUGGCACUAUUGAGUGACUUUUGCUGGGAUUGCAGUUUAAACCAGGGAAACAGAACGCAGCCUGUGGGUGAGCCAUGUUUGGAGACGGGCAUGGGAGGGUCAGAAGGAGGCUGGAAGGCUGCCUGGAGAAGAGACUGUGGAAGCCUGGGGAGGGUGUUAAUGAAGUAUCUGACUGUGUGAUCUGCAGCUGCUCAGACAGCUGAAGUCAGAUGGCCUGGGAUGGUUGAGAAUCAGGGACCCAAAGUCAACAUGAGAGCAAAGAGCCACUCCAGCAGCUGUGAAGAAGUGAAAACCAAGGAGAGAAGGGGGUCUUGCAUUAGCAAGUGGGGAUCUGAGUUUGAGAUAGAGGAGAAGGAGCAGGUCAAGAGGAUAAUGGGGUUGAAUUUGCAGUGCUAGUGGAGGGCUCAAGAGGUUGGAGGAUGGAGUUUAUUAUAACGGGAGCUCAGAGAAUAAUCAUCUCUAAUUUAUUAUUGACGCUGUGCUCAACAUUCAACAUCCAUGUUCUUCCUCAAAAGCUCCCUGCUGGAUAGUGUAAGUGCCACUACCAUAGAAAGAUUCUACUUCAUCAUGCCUGGUCUACUACAGCCUCUUAGCUGGUGCUCCUGACUCAAAUUACUCUGUUUGUGGUCAGUUCCUUAUUCCACUACAAGGCUCAUCUUCUUAAAACAUCACGUUUAAUAGGUUACUGUGAAGAUCUAAAAGCUUCACUGAGUACCCAUUGCCUACAGUAUAAAGGAUGUGCCCCUCCAUAAAGUGAGAAAUCGCCAUUUUUGCCGGCUUUCGUAAUUUACCAAUGACUCUUACACACAUAAUCUCAUUGAAUUCUUACAAAAGCCGUAUGAUAGUGAGGAUAUAUAUUUCUCUUUUUCUAAGUUUAUAAAUAACAUAAUAGAGGAUCAGACAUGUUAGAUGACAUAUCCAGGGCCACACAGUUCAUGAGUGGCAGAGCCAGAGAUAGAUAUCAAGUCUUCUGAGUUCAAGUCCAAGGUCCUUUGCCCCAUACCAUGUCCUCACCUUGGAGCCCCAUCUCCAUUCUAACCUUAGGAUUUCUGUAAUUAGGAUGAUGAGGCGAGGUGCCUUCAGUCCCAGCAGGAUUGCAGAGAGGCCUCUCAGUGUCCCUACAGUCACUUUUUAUCACCACUCAGAAGUUGUGAUCUGGGGCUGUCAACUGAGACACAUUUCCUGGCUGGUUUUCCCUUAGAUUGGGAAAAGCCUGUCUCCUGCCAGGACAUCUGGGGAGGCACAGAAAACACUCUGUACUUCCCUGAUGUCAUCCUCAGUGCCUGCUUGUCUCAUAUGGAACUUGGAGACGGUUGCCACUGACUUCACAUGGGGUUAUGGACAGCUUUUGACCACUGCCGGCACCAUCCCUUCCUGCUUCAGUUGCUGUCACCAGUAAGGCGAGAAAUAGGCUUUGAAUUCAUGAAUUCACACCCACAGAAACUCUAGGUCUGAAUACUUGUUUCAAAAUGUAUUCUCAGUUGUUAUCUUAAUGGAUGUAUAAAUUCGUUGCCAUUUAGCUGUGAAUCGUUUGGAAAAUUAUGUAUACAGAAGGGUGUAGAGCUGUGCUUUGAAAUACAUGUUGAAAUUGGGAACAUUUGUUAGCUAUGCAGUGAUUAAUGAGUCUGUGUUAACGUGAUUUUAGAGUACACUCUGUUUCCAUCAUUUUCUCAUUGUGCUGAAGCCAAUGUCAUGUGGAUUUUGACAGAGUUUUUUGGAGACAAUUUACUGCAUCAGAAGUUUAAAUGAUAUCAGAAAUAUGCCUGACAAUUGCCGAGAAUAUCAAGAUUGCCUCCACUCCUAUAAAAAUCAGUGAUGGAAAUAUGUUCAUGAGGAUUAGUUAAAUAAUAUAUUGGAAGAGUGCUGCAUCACCUUUUGGGCUCCAUGUUAAGACACACACACACAUACACACACACAGAAACACACAAUCCCAGCACUUGUUUGGAAAUUUUGCCUUUGCAUUCUUUCACUUGCAUUUCCACGAUCAAGCAAUACAUCUUUCUAAUCACAAAAGCUAAAGAAUAGUUGAAAUACCUUUUACAAGCCCAUGUUAUAAUCCUCAUUGUACCUCAUGGUACCUCACUCCCUUGUACCAGUGUAUUUCUUUUGGGGACAAUAGCAUAGUUUCUCAGGAGGCUGUGAUCUCAGGAAGUCUCCUAAUUUUUCUAGUGCCUUUCACAUGUUGGAAUUAAAAGGUCAGUAAAGAUAUAGUUUAGGAGUAUGAAGGGCUCAACUGCCAAACUUUGGAUUUUUUUUUUCUCUUUACUUUCUCUAAUUUAACCAAAGGUGUAGAAUGAUGCACAAUACAUUGGAAUGAGAUACAAUUUGGACUUUGGUAGUAAACCAUUUUAGGGCGGGAACAAGAUGUGUAAAUCCUAAAUAGUGUUGAAUGGAAAUGUUCUGGAAAAGGAAUUUCAGUUCUGAACUGUGAUAUUACAUUAUUUACUUUCUGGGGAAUUAAAUAAAAAUUUGUAUUGUGGUAUUCAUUGGAAAUACUGAUUUAUAUUGUGGCCAUAUUUUCUUAUAUUGUGGCCAUAUUUUCUUCACUUGGCCUUAGUUACUUAGCAGUCACCUAAUAAAACUUGAAUAAUUAAAGAGGGCAUUCUUGAUUAAAACUAACUAGAUAUAUGUGUACUUCAUGAGCUUGUUAGUGCACAGGUUGGACUACAUGGUGAAGAUGGCCAAUAAGACUAGUUUAUAUGUUGUUCAAAGCAUUAACAAUGGUAAAAGUGAUAAUAUAUGAUAAUAAAGAAAAGGGCAAAAAUAUACAAAGUUGAUACUUUUGUAGAAACUGUUAUGCCUUAUUUUUACCUUUAUUUACUUUAAUGUUUUUAUUUGAGACAGGGUGUCACUCUGUUGCACCCCCUGGAGUGCAGUGGUGCGAUCUCAGCUUACUGCAAUCUCAACCCCCUGGGCUCAAGUGAUCCUCUCACUUCAGCCUCCUGAGUAGCUGCGACUAUAGGCCCAUGCCACCACGCUCAACUAAUGUUUGCAUUUUGUGUUUGUGUGUGUGUGUGUGUGUGUGUGUGAAGAUGGGAUUUGGCCACGUUGCCCAGGCUGGCCUUAAACUCUUGGGCUCAAGCAACCCACCUCCCUCGGCCUCCCAAAGUGCUGGGAUUACAGAUGUGAGCCACCACUCCUGACCUAUGUCUUAUUUUUAAAUACAGGCAUUGUGUGACAUAUCCUAUAAUAGAAUUUUUCAAAAGUACUUAGCCCUUUUGCAUUUCAUCACUUUAUUUUCUCCUAUCUUGUUGAAUGAUUCUUGGGAUUAGUGGCACUCAAUGGGAAUCAUUCUAACUUUCCCUGGCCUUGUGCAUUCUUUGGAGCUGUCCCUAUGGCCUAUUCCUCUCCAUUUUUGCUGUCUACUAAUGCAGGCUCUCAUCACUGCACCUGUCUACUAUGGAAGCUUCUGUCUUGAAUUGAUCUCAUACGCUGCUAUCAGAUUAAUUUUACAAUAACUCUCUUUUAGCACCCCUCUUUCCUGCUCAAAGUUCUUCAGAGGGUCUUUAUUAUCCAUAGGAUGACAGGUAGCUUAGAGCCACAAAAAUAGCACAGGAAGUGGAAUCCAGAGACCUGUUUUAAAUUGCUUGGCUUUAACUUGCUUUGUGACCCUGGAAACAUUACUGUUCACCAAAACUCCUCAAAUUUAUCUUUACUAACUGUCUUAAGUUCCUCACCUCUCAUAUAUCUUACCAAAGCCAGUGAUCAUUCUUCGUCGUCAUCUUCUCAACUCUUUACAACGUUUUGAACAGUUGACCACUCUGUCUUGUUUAAUGAAAUGCUUGAUCCUCCCAGCUUCCAUGACACUACACUUUCUCCCAUCUUUCCCUGUCAGUCUUAUUUGCUAGGCUGCCCCUAAGUGUUGGACUCCCUUAGGGUUCUAUCUAAAUCCUCCUAUCUUCUUUAUCUAAAUUCUCUUUCUAGCAGAUAUCCCAGCAUGGUUUAGAAUAUCAUCAAUAUGCUAAAUAAUUUUCAAAGUUUUAUUUUCAUUAAUGGAUCUAUCAUGAAUUUUCAACUUGUAUUCCUCCUAAAUCCAUGCACUUGGCUGUCCAAUGGACAUAUCAAAGUUGAAAUAGGCAAAAGAGAACUAUCAGUGUCCCCCUGCCUACAGCUGUGCUCCUCCACCAAACCUUUCCAUUUCACCAAACAGAACCAUGUUUCACUAAAUCAACCAUGUUUGUUGCUCAGGCCAUAAUUCCAGAAUUCAUCCUGGAUUCCUCUCCUUCCUCCCAGACUCACAUUUAAUCCAGUAAGUACUUCUGGCUCUCUCUCCAAAAUAAGUGCUGAAUGUUAUGUCUUCUUACUCUCUGCUCUGCUAUAGUUUCAGUCCAAGCCACCAGCAUCUGUCCUUGUAGGCUGCAAAAGCUCUUACUAGGCUUCCCUGCCUCCACACUCCCCAGAGUAGCCUAUUAAAUAUAAAUUAUAUAAUACCCUCCCUUGCUAAAAAUUAUCUAAUAGAUGCAUUCUCCUAACCUUUAGAAUAAAAUCCAAGCUAUUCACCAUGUCCCAUAGGGCUCUGCUUCUCUGGGCUCAUUUUCCUCUACACACCCCAUUCCCAGAUAGGUUCCAGUCAUAAUGGCCUUCAUUCUGUUCCUUAAACUUGCUGAGCUUGUUUUUGUCCCUGUCUUUGCACUUACUGCUUUUCCUGCUGGCAGUGCUUUUUACCUGCAUAUCCCCUGCAUGGCUCCUUGUCAUUGUUCAAGUCUCAACUCAAAUGUCCCUUCUUUGGACAGGCCACCUGUGACCCAAGUUUGAGCAGUUUCCUUAAUCCAUCCCUAGUUCAGUUUUUAUUGCAUUUUUUACUUCAUAGAAAUGAUCAGAAUCUGAAAUGAUCAACUUAAUAGUUGAUGUAUUUUUUGUCUGUCUGUCCCCAGUGUGGACUCCCUGAGGUCACUGACAUUUUAUUAUUCACCUCUGCAUCUCAGUGCCUAGUAGAGAAGAUGGUGUAUAGGAAGCACUUAAAGAAUUUGUUGACUCAUUCACCACUUUGAGCCUAGCUUCCUUAUCUGUAAACCAAAGGUGUCAGGACAGGGGACCUCUGACCCUGCCCUACCUAGCCAGUUUUAAUUCUUAUCGUGUCUCUAAGCCCUCUGAUCCAGUCCAGUUGACCUCCUUAAGGUCCUAUAAAUGGACCAUGUUUAUUCAGAUCUUCAGGCCUUUGCUCAUUCUCUUCCCUCCUGAGUGUCCUUCUUUUUGGUCCUUGCUGGCUGCAUUUGUCAAUAAUUUUCCUUCUUCUCUUUUGACUCUACCCCUCAUAGAAGAGUAUAAUUGUUUUAUAUAUACAUGUCUUUCCUGUCCUAGUUGUUAGUCCUUAGGCAUAGGGCUAUGGUUUAUAGUCAUAACUCUUUUGAACCUCCUUGGUGAUAGCAUAUAGGAUAUACUCAGUACAUGCCUUAUAAUUCAAUAAGGGUGUGCUGUCUACCGAAAACACUGAUUUCAAAACAAUAAUCAUGCUUGGUCUGCUUACUAAUUUAUAUGGGAUAAAAAUAGAUUUUUUAAAAAAGCAACUAAACAGGUAUAUCUUUGUUAAGCCUGAGCUGGAGAAAAAAAAAUCUAAAAAUGGAAAUUUAAACUUCUGGUAUCAUGGUGUUUUGAAAACAUUUGUAAGCAACCUUACCAAAAGUUUUGUUAUAGAUUUUUAUUUCAUUUAAGUUUUUAUAUAUUCAUGAGUAGUUGAAAAAGGAAGUGAACAUUGUUUUUUAUUAACUCAGGUUAAAAACUUGAGUUUUUAAUUUGGUUCAGUUUGUUCAGGUAUUUGGAAUUUAGAGAAGCUCUGUGAAAAUAUCCCGCCUACACGUUUUGAAUAUCCUCUUCCUGCUUAUCUUCAGAACAGCUUGGUUCUUUUAAUAGCAAAUGGCUGAGUGGAGGGGAACCAUUUGCAGUGGGUCAAUUUAAGUAUGGUGUGUCCUCCCAUUUCAGACCGAAGUCAUGCUAACUGCUCAGGGAUUGGUGCAACUGUGUGUUUCUUUUGAUGUUGGUCAGAUCCCAGAAAACUCAGUAUUUUAGAAGGAUGUUGCUCAUUCCUUAGAUAAUUUGAAAAAUUAUUGGUCAACUUAAAAAAAUUCAGGAGCUAGGGAACACCUCAUCUAUUCUUUUUAUGAAUAUGUUAAUUUAUUAUUCUGUUGGAGGCUGUUCUUAAAAUUCCCAUGGGCCAGGAUAGGAAGAGGUAAUGGGGAGAAGGCUUGUUUUUUCAUGCAAUAUAUGAACCUAGCGCUAUAUGAUCAUGCCAGAUUCAGUAUACGCAAAUGGUGUAUUUCUCUCAAUCCAGAGUGGCUGGAAAAUGUGUGCUCAAAAUUGAGAAUAAUCAUAUAUUCCAUUCAUGGAUUAAUUGUUUUCAAAUAAUGUAGUCAAUUAUACUUACAAUGAUUUUUUAAGUUUUAAUAACAUAAAAGACACUUCGUAUAUGUAAGCCUGUGGUAAAUCAUGGUGUACCUCAUUUACUAGUCAAUAGUAUUGGUGUUCAAAAUAAUGGUGGUGAUUGGAUUAAUUCUCAGUCCAUCCCAGAAUUUGCUGUUUUGAAUAUACAGCUUGUUUUUAAGGUAUCCACUUCUUUUGGGAAAGUAGAGAUAAGAAAAAAGUCUGCUUCUUUAAAUGUCUUGUUUGGAUUGGGGGCACACAGCCAUUUUUUUUCUAGUGAGUAGAUAUAAAGGAUUUCCCAAAAGGUGGCUGUGGCUUCGCACAGGAGAGCUGGAGAGCUCUUGGUACAUAUACUGCUGAGUGUUGAAGGCAGGUGAGUCUGUUCUAUGUUUCUGUGCAGUGGGCUCUUGCUGGGGUCAAAGCUGUGUGGUGUCUGUAAAAAAGGGUUGCUGUGUAAUGCUUUAGAAUUGGAAUUGCAGAUUCUUCUUGUGAGGGGAAUAUUGCUGUUAUGGGUAAAAGUUGUGUCUUAUGGUUGCCCUUGUGACCUUGUUAGAUCCUUUGGAUAAUUAAAACUUCCAGAAGUUGGGAUUGUAGAUGCUGGGAAUGUAGAAAAACAAUAGUCAAAUCAGUCAAAAAGGUGCUAACCAUUGGGAUAAUACACUGAAAAGCAUCCAGUGGGAAAUUUAUGAAUUGUAAAAAACCCAAUACUGCAUGAAAUCAUAACUUCCUUUUAUGACCCUCAAUCGUGGCCAUUAAAGGGCUAACUUCUGUUACAGAAAAGAGGUAGCUAGUUAGUUCAUAUCUCUGGGUUUAGAUAAAUCACAGUAUCUCUCUUAGUUUUGGUUUGGCAGGAUGUCUUGGACCUUUUCCUUUGGUUUCCUUUGGUUGUUAGAUAAAGACAUGUGAGGAUGGACUCUGUGACUGCAUGGUUUUCUUCCGGGUGAGCUCACUGGCUUGCCACCGCCCAGAUUUAUCAGCAGCUGGAGUUUCACCUAAUAGUAUGGUUUGCUCCAACCAUUUGCUGGAGCAGAAAAAGAUGGCAUCAACUUAUAUUUUAAAAUAAACUGACUUUGAAAGGUUUUAUGAAAUCACGGUCCAUUUUGAUUAGUUUUUGCCAACAGCUGCCUGCAUUUAGGCUUUGUUCUUUGUUGGACAUAACUGUUUAGGAAAGAUUGCUGCUUUAUGGAAGCGAUUCCAAAGACUCAUUGUUCCAGACAUCGGACAUCCUUAUGUUAUUCAGGUCUGAUGAUAUUUGAUCUAACGCAGAUUAAUUACUAAGCUCUCAGUGAAUAAUUAACCAUUUGACCUGUUCCCAAGUUAUAUACUCACUGAGUUAGAAAUGAUUUCCCCAACUACUAAAGAUAAGGAAGGUUAUUCCUGGUUUCACAGUGUCCCCAUUGUUACUGACUUGUAUGUGUGAGAGACAUCAGCUGAUACCUACGCACUGGUCCAGCUACUCAGUCAAACCACUUCCUGGGGUUUUCUCGGGUAAUGGCAGUGAUUCAGAAGACACCACAGAACUUUCUGAGGACUGUUCCCUGUGUGUUACUCUGGGCUGAAUGACUGGGAACUGUCAAGUUCAAAAGGAACAUUUUUUGUUGUAGUGCUAUUAAAUUUGUGGUUUGCUUUUGCUCAAAGUUGCAUUUCAGCUGAAUUUAGGGUGGCUUGUCUGUGUGCCAUUUAUUUUAUAGUACCUAAUUUCCAUCAAUUAACCAUUUCAUGCCUUAGUUGAGUCCCUUAUAAAGUCCUGUAUUAAGCCUGGAGGGGAUAGGCAAACUAAGUCAUUAUAACUGCCUGCAGUGGCUAGUAGUAAUUAGGGAGAGGAGAGAUAAAAAUGGAUGGGGGCCAAAUAGGGUAUUAAUGCAAACAUUGUACUUUUCUACUUAUGUAUUUUUGUGAUUUUUUUUUUUUACUUCUGAUCUAUUCACACAAUGUACUCCAUAAGGUAAAUUUUGUAUUUCUAGGAUUAUAUUUAUAAUAUAAAAAUGCAGAUAGAAUUAUUUUAAUAAAGUUUUUGUUUUGUUUUGUUUUAUGGUCUUGCAUAAAAGGAAAAUAUUUCAAAAUUAUUUUGGAAUCACAAGAUAUGUGUUCUUUUCUAGUCCUUCAGAAGUUCCAAAAUUUCAGUUUUCAUUGUAGAAUGAAUAAGCAAGAACCCUGGGCACUAGUUCUCUCCUUGGUUACUCUGACGCUUGGCUUACCUUUUUCCUUCCAAUAUUUGCACAUCUUUUCUUCCCCUCAUGGCUGGAUGAUCCAGUCUUGUGAGAUAAUGUAUAAUGGAAGCAUUCUGUAACCUGGAAGUGUUAUGAAUAAGCAUGUAUUAUUAUCACCAUUAUUUUCACAUAUUCAUUGAUUGCAUCAUCUCAUCAAACAUACCAGUAAUUCACUUCUGCAAUGUCAGAGAUGAUUGUAAAUAUCUCAGUGGAGAAGCGACUUUCUUCUUGAACUUAAGAAAAUCACUGGUAGAACCAUGUUUUAGGCAAAAUGUCGGUUUCACUGGUCCCGCUUUCAGUGUCCUGACCAAGAGAAAGUUGGGAAGAGUAGGUGUACAAAGUGAAAAGAUUCAGUAUAUCUAUAUGGUAUGGUAAUUGUACAUUGCUUGGCUCUCAGCACACUGUGAGGCUCACUUUACAAAAAUUGGUAUUUGGUUUUAGAAACAACUCUAUUUUUAAAAUGGGAGGUUGUUUGUGGUAGGGGUUAAGAGUGUGGGCUCUGGAAUUAAAUGGGCUUGCCUCCUGUCCUGGUUCCCUCAAUUCUAGCUUUGUGAAAAUCAGGUGAGUUUUAAAUCUUUUUGUGCUUCACUUUUCUGCUGGUAGAACAGGGAUGAUUAUUAUAUGGUAGGGUUGUUGUGAAGCCUAACUGAAGUAAUGCACCCAGAGCACUUGCCACUCAAUACAGAUUACAGGAAGAAAUAGAGUUCCAUGUUAAAGUGAUGGAAUGUAUCAUUCGCAUCUCUCAGACUGUUGUGGAUUCUAUCUGAUGGGAUUUGGUUCAGUUUGAUGACCUGUCUCUUGAGAGUAAAUAAAAGGGGGCAGGAGGAUGCUCAUGGGACGUCAGAGAAAGAAGAAGGAGAGGCCCUAUUGUACAUUCCGCAAAAAACAAAUUCAUGCGCUUUAUGGGGCCUGGCAGUUUAUAAAGUUCUUUCAUGUACAUUGAUUUCAUUUAAUCCUCCCAACAACACCUGUUUUACAGAUAUGUAUACUGAGCCUCAGAGACACUCAAGGACUGGCUCACAGGCAUGUGGUCAGUGAGAGUGCGGUGAGGAAGCAGACCUCCUGGAUUCUGGACAUAUUUCUUCAUUCCAACCCAUGGGUCCUUCUCUGCUGUAUAAAAAUGUUCAAGUCAAUAAUAACCUUUGGUGCUGAACCCCAAAGGAUUGGCAGGGUGUGGGCUGCUGCAGACCCAGGUGGGUCUUGGUGGGGAUCCAGGACCUUCUGUCUGUGAUAUGUAGAACAUGAAUGCGCAGCCCUUCAGUGGUCACGGCUGCCAGAUGGUUUUAAGAGUCCCCUGUCUCUUUGUGGCCUCUGAGUGAGGCUUGCAUUUCAAUCUCUGUGAAGGGCCACUUUGGAUCAGUGUUCUGUGGGAGAAAUUAAGGGUCAGUCUUCUCUUUUUGCUAAGAAGGAAGGUAAUGAACACCUAUCUAAUGGUUGAACAUGUGUGUGUUUUACAAGAUUAAUAGUAUUAAUACCCUUUCAACCCAAGCCUUUUUGGGUCACUGUGUUAAUAAAAUGAAGUUGGAGAGUAGAGUAAAAUAAUUAAUGUAUAUAUAACGUAACUCUUAGUUUGAUUUAACUGGUUAAUCUGUGAUUCAGUAUACAUUUUUAAUACAUUUUAAAUUUUAAAAGUGGCGAUACACUUUUACAUUUAUUUCUUUGGGUUCUGAGAUUAUAAAUAGCUUUAAAAGUUGGAGUGCCCUAUUUGUCAUGCUAAAAAUCAAGUGAGUUAAGACGUGGGAAAGUGAUCAGAGAAAAUUCAGUAUAGUACUUCAGAAUUUUUAAAAUACUGAAAACAAAUUUUAAAAUUAGUUAUUUCACACACAUUAAUGUGUAAAGACUGCAUUGAUUUGGGUAUUACAUUUGAACACAUUAUUUUUAUGAAAUAAUUUUUUUAUUCUGAGUCAGAAAUUUGUACAUAGUUGAUACUAUAUAUAUUUAUCAAAUGAAUUUGUUUUUAUGGAAUAAAAUUUUGAUUAGCUAUAAUAUACUUUUUUUUGGCUACAUGCACUUCAUUUUUCAGGGAAGAGGUAGGUAGCUAGAAGAAAGCAUGACAUACUAUCAGUAAUUUAUUUUUUAAAGCAACAUCUAGGCCAGGAUUUCUCAACCUUGGCAUUGUUGACAUUUGGUUCCAGAUAAUUCUUUGUUGUGGAGGGGCUGUCAUGUGCAAUGUAGAAUGUUUAGCAGCAUUCCUGGCCAGCUACCCAAUAGAUACCAGUAGUUUUCCUUCUCCCCAGUUGUGACAAUAAAAAAUGUCUCCAGACAUUGCCAAAUAUCCCCUAGGGGGCAAAAUCACCCUUGGCCGAGAACCACUGAUCUAGGAUUUUCAACAUUAUAUUUAAAUCUUCUACCUAACCUAAAUCUACAUUAUUCUACAAAUUUGAAUCGAUGUUCAGACUUACACUAAAAAGGAGAAAAUGCUAUACUUACAGAGGCAAUACUUAUCAAUUAUGAAAAAUAAGAUUUUUCAACAACAUGGGUUAGGAUAAGUGUUUUCUGAUUAACCCUUAUUUACCAUAAUAUAAUCCAAUUAACCAGAAUUUCACACAUUUGAAAUAAUGUUUUAUCCCCUUAUUUUCUUUCAAAAUAGAUAUAUCCCCUGAUUCUGAAUUAAUUUAUAAUAAUGAUCUGGAUAGGGCUUUUUAAAAACUUUCAAAGAUGGAAGUAGUAUUGUAGUUUGCCCUAUAUUGAAUUAGAUCAUUCUGGGUAUUCCUCAUGCACAUACUGAAAAGUUUAAUUGCCUUUAUAGUUGGGUGUGUGUCUUGAUGAAUAAGGAUUUGUGCAACAUGAGCUGAAGAGUUAGAUUUCAGAAGUCCACUUAUCAACUCUUUCAUGGACAUUUUAGCAUAAGGAGACAAAUAGACAUACUUGGUUAUUAAUUAUUAUAGGGAUAUAGACAUUUCACUUGGCCCGAGAUUUAAGUGAUUGCUCUUUAAAAUGUGUUUUGCUCAUGAUAGAAUGUAUUUUUGUUCUUGUGAACCAUGCACUGAAGCUUUAGCCAAUCAGAGGAAGGAAUUUACUGUACGGUAAAAGGAAGUAUUUGUUCCGUUAUUGUAGUAUGUGGCCUCUUGCCAUUUUUGAUAAAGGAUUGAAGUGUUGUGCACCCAAAGUCUGCUACCCUCUUGACCCUUCAUCAAUCAUCAGCUGGACUGUGAGGUUAAGUGAACUGUAGCCCGGUAGGAUAACUAUUGUUUAAGCAUUGUGUAACUCCUGAAAGCGGAAAUUACUGACACAGCUGACUUGCAAUGUGAUCUUUCUAGUUUUAAGAUUAUAUGCAUAAUUUUCCUUUCUGUUUCUAAUCUAUGCCAGAUUAGAGGUAUAAAAUGACAGUAUAUAGGACUUGAAGUCAUGUUAUUCAAUGGAUGACCGUGAGACUGUUGGAAAUUUAUUUUUAUUUGCAAGAAUAGGAACCUGUGCAAAAAUAAAUGACCUAUUCUAGCACAACGUUUCAAGAAAUUCAUAUGGGAUCCUAUUGGAAUUGUUAUUGCCUUAAAACCACUAGGAUAGCAACCAAGUCUUGCAUGCGAAUCCACCUUUAUUAAUGCGUUAGUUACUGAAAGCAUAUAUUUGUCCACAUGUUUUCUAAGUAACUGGCAGCAUACACAAAUUCUUUUAGCACAUAUCCUGUUUUUUUGAUUGGCUCAGGAAAACUUUAUAAGAGCCAUGUCCAACAUUCACAGCUUUAUGUCAUCUCGUCUCUGUAUUUAUGUCACUUUCUUAAACAAGUAGAGUAAUAUAUCAGCUGCAGCUGUUGCUGACCAAAGCUGUCACUGAAGUGGGUGGAGGAAGAGUCAGAGAUAAUGUGUUCAGAUUCUGUGUACCAAAAGCAUAUCUGUUGCAAUCAAUCUGUAACGAUAACAACUGGCUUGUAGAAGGCACUUCAAGCCAGAUACUUUUUUAUCUUUGACCAAAUGUAUAGUAGAUUAGAUGCCAUGAUGAUAAAUACCACUGAUAGUUAAUACAAUCUGGUUGAGUAUAUAUAUGAUUGCCUGGCUUGUAUAAUAAGAAAGACCACUGAUGUGUAGUCUUCACCAGGUUUGGCCACAGCCUUCCUGUAAAGUUAUUAACACAAAACUUGAUACUUAAUAGCAUGCAAAGAAAAAAAAAGACUAUGAAAUACCUAAUAGCAAAAGAGUAAAAUCCUUGUUUUCUGAUAUAGACAGUGAUGCUUCCUAAUAAGUGUAUUUGGAUUAAAAGAAAUAUUCACACUAACACACACGUCCAAUUAUUUAUUACAAGAAUUCUACCACCAUACUUACCCAGAGCAGGUUGGAAAUACUGGAGUCAGUACCUCUCUACCUAAGAUUUCUUAUAACCCUCUGGAUCCUUACCCUUUGUCAACUUCUCCUGUUCACCAGUUUACCACAGGGAGGACUGAAAAUUCCCACUGGAAGAUUAUAGCUUAAUUUUUAUUUUCUUUUUCGCUUUUUAUAAAGAUAGUUAAUGGCAAAGGGAAAUUGUAUUUUAGCAGUUAGAAAGGGGUAAGUAGCCACAUUGGCCUGAGGCUCAUUGCACUUUCACCCCAUUAGAGUAAAAUGAAAUCCUGAUGUGGUCAGAUCAACUAAGGGAGAGACCGACCUCAAAGAUAAAGAGAAAGCCCUUUCCACAGCUUUAUAUAUUUAUCCUUUUCCCAGUAAUUCUCCUCGUUGUCCUUAGCAUCAAAGUACCUAUUUCUUUUGGAAUUACUAUUCUGCCUUAUAAAGAGAAUCUCCCAGACUAAAUGCUCAUGGUAUAGAAACUUAAAAUUAAAGGUAGGCACUUUGACAUGGAUCUACAUACAUGGGAGAAAGAGGUAAUAAAGGAGUUAGGAGUUAGCACUGACCUAACGCUACAAGAAAAUUUCACAGCAGAUGUGGAAUUUCAGGAACUGUCUACUAAUGGGAAAUAAGGGUUGUAGAAAAGGAAGAAAAAUUAAGUAUGGCCAAGUAUUAUUGAGCAUCAAUGAUUAUGCUCAGUGAUUUAUUAGUAGCUAACAUCUAUUGAGCACUUACUGUGUGCCAGGUAGGAAUGCUUUCUGUGUAUUAACUUAUUUAGGUUCUCAACAAGUUUUCAAGGCUGUUGCUGAUAUUAUCCUCAUUUUACAGUUGAGGGAAAGGAGGCAGGAAACUAAAUAACUUGCCCAAGGUUCUAGAGGGCAUUAGAGGCAGAGCCAGGAUUAGAAUUCAGAAAGUCUGAUUUAGAGCUUGCCUCUUCACCAGUUGCAGCAUGCUGCUUACCUAAUUUAAUUUCCACCACAGCCCUCCAAAACAGGUAUUUUCUUCCAUUUACAAAUUUUACAAAUGAGGAACUCAAAGCCUAGAGAGGUUAAUUUUGUCAAGGUCAUCCAGCUGGCCAGUGGUAAAGGAAGGAUUCGAACCAAGGUCUGAUCCUCAAAAGUCUGUGCUUUUUCACUGUAAGAAGAGGCUGUCUUGGGAUGGCCUAGAAGUGUAACUGACAGAGGGAUCCAGCUCCUUCCUUGUAAGUUAAGAUUAUUAAAAAGCUUGUAUAGGUUGUUCAUAACUCGUCCCAAGGCAGUAGAGCUGAUGUUUACUGAAGCAUGCGAAACGCUUUCUGGUUCACCUCUAUCUUCUAGAAAUCGUCUGCCUGCCAUCAUCCUAGGUCGUGUGCUUCAUUUCAUUUGGUGUGCCUCUUUUCAAUGUACUGGGCUGUUCUAUUCCUGUUUAUAAAUCUUUUAAGUGUGCACAUUAAAAAAGUAAUUAAAAUGUCAUUAUAAUUUAUAGUAUGCCUGAAGUCAAUCACCUAAUUAAACUACAAGAGAGAAGAGGUGGUACGUUCGUAGGCAUUUAUGAAGUAUUACUGUAUUAAUUAUGCAGGGAUUUUGAACCAAGUAAAAGAAAAAGGUACUGGUAACAUUAUUCCUUAAAGUGUUUCCUUUUUUUUUUUCUUCUCAGUUUCAGACCUUCACUAGUUGGUAGCAUAACCCUAAUGUGUCUUUUGGCUAAUUUUUAAUGAAAUUAGGAUUUUUAUGUCUUUCACUCAGCAUUUUCUUAAAAUGCUCCUGACAGCAUUAAUGUGCAUCAUCCCACAUCCUAACUGAAUAAGCAAUUAGAAGCACAAUAGAAAACAAAAUUUGAAUUCAUGGGUUAUACAUAGCUAUCCAAAUUCUCUUUUGGAGUAUAAAAAUGGCAGCAUAUUGGAUAUCUGGAAUCAUUCAGAAGAGAUUUGGUUUUCCUGGAGCAAUAGUAGCUAUCAAGAGACUUAUUUUCUUAUUAAAGAACAAAAAAGCAACCACAACAAAAACAAAAACAAAAUUCACAUGGCCAAGUAAAAUAGGCUGUAAUAAAUCUCUUGCUGGAGGAAACUAUUUUUGAAAAGCUGUUUUUGAAUUCUAAGUGCUAGCACAUAUAGGUAGAUAGACACAGAUAUAGACAUAGUUAACUUUUGUUAUGUGAGAAUUGAUGACUUGGAUAGGUGUUUCAGCCCCUUGGGAGGUCUUUGCAGUUUGUAAUGGAAUUGGUUGGCUAUAUGAAUUCUUACAGGGUUAGGACCUUCAAGGAAAGGAGAAUUCUGAGGGAUAUGAUUUAGUGUCAUCCAUGUGAGUGAAAGAUUUGUGCAGUGAAUUUUUCCUACCCUGUGUUUAUUAUUUUGGAGGAUGAGUAGAAUGAAAGGCUCUAAUUCUCAGAAGCAAUCCUUAAAAAGAAAGGCAAUAAAGGCAUUUAACUGUUAUGUAAUAGCAAAUGUAUAUAGCUUCAAGUUAUUAGGUGCUCAAAAAAUUAUUGGGUGAACAAGUGUCUUGUGUAGACUCCAGUUUUCUUUGUUCCUCUAUGUGCAUGUACAAUAUCCUAAACGUAUAAACAGUUUUCAUAUUAAUAUUUAUUAUUUUUCGCUAAGUCACAAAAGCUGAGUUGACCUGUAGUGUACUUGAAGUAUUAGUAAUAGUUAAGAAGUUAAAAUGUGGAUGUCAGUUUCUUUGGAAAACUUCAUUCUGAGUGAUAAGCUGUGAUGUUGAGGAACACAGCUCUUUCUGCUAUUGUGAGAGCAGCACUUUACCCUCCGUUUCUAGGCUGUUCCUAGAAUUCUUGGUUAAAGGGACCUCCAGGCUCCAGGUGACACUCCUGUAGGCUGCUGGUGAUGGGACUGGGAGUUGAGCAGGAGGUGAAAUACAGAGAGUGAGCCAAGGCAGGUUUUAGUUCAAGGCUGCUGGGCUGAGGGGGAGAGAUAGACAAAAGAGUAAAAUACUCAACAAGGGUAGCAGAGAGGAAAGAAAGGACACCCCCUACAGCCCUCUUGCUGGCUUGGCUGCUUACUGGGUGGUCUUUCCAAUGGUAGGGGCAAAGGUAAAUCAUGCACAUUUAAUUAGAAAAUUGCUAACACACACAUAUCCUCUUAACACGAUCUUUGUUUACAGCAGUAUAAACAUUUCUCCACAUGGAACCAAAGCUACAUAAAAUAAUAAGCAUGAGAUUUAAAUAAAGAUUUUGCUUAUAAGUGUGUUUUUGGGACCUGUGGACUACAAAUAUUCCUUGAAUCAGUGCUCACUGGAAUGUGAGCUUUCCCACAGAAAGAAGUGUGUCUUACUCCUUGGGGGAUCCUAAUCUCUGUCCGAGAGAUUCAUACAGAGCAGGGACCUCAAAAUGUGCAAUAUGCAAAAGCGUAGUUAGAUGAAUGUAGAUGUGAGGUAUUGUGAAGAUUUUGGUAUUUUUCAUUUACUUUAAACCUGGCAUGACAUUUACUAUUGAAUUUGACCUCUUCUCUAAACUUAUUUUAUUUCCUCUUUCUUUCUGAGAACUCAAUUAAAUCUCUUAAAAAAUUCAUAACUUGAUAUUUGCGUGUCCUGUCUUUAGAAAUAUUUUGUAAUAUUUUAUCAGAUAUGCCUUGAUUCUUCAGAAAGCAAUAUCUUAGAAAAGCUAUUUUUUGUAUAGUAAUUGUUAAUAGUCAUUAGUAAUUUAAAGAAGUUAAUUUGUAAUUUCCAAAAGAAUCUGAGAUUUUGAAAUAAAAACAGUCUUAAUGUGUUAAUGUCAAGAACAUUGGACAAGGCAGAUACAAAAGAUUUGGUUUGUAUCUAGGAUUUACAUUAAAGUAACACAAACUACUAUAACUGGUAGUUUAUUUUAACAUAUAGUUUUGUUAUAAGAGGUUUUAUAUUAAAUUUUGUGGUGUACUCUGGAGCUGUGAACAGGGAAUUUAUUAAAAAAAAUGCAACAGAACCUGUUCUUGCCUUUUUUAUAUAUUGCAUUUGCUACAUUAGCAAAUCUAUUAUAUAUUAUGUAAUAUAUUUAUUAUAUGUAAUUAUAUAUUACAUAUAAUUACAUAUAUUACAUAAUAUAUAAUAUAUUAUGUAAUAUAUAUUACAUAUUGUAUGUAAUAUAUAAUAUAUGUAAUUAUAUAUCAUAUUAUAUAUUACAUAUAAUAUAGUACACAAUAUAUAUUAUAUUAUAUGUAAAGUACAAUAUAUUACAUUUUAUAUAAUACAUAUAAUCUAUUAUAUGCAAUAUAUACAUAUAAUAGAUAUUUAUAUAUUAUAUAUAAAUAAAUAUAUAUAAUUUAUAUAUUAUAUAAAAAUAUAUAUGAUAUCUAAAUAUAUUAUAUGUAAUAUAAUUACAUAUAAUAUAUUACAUAAUAUAUGUAAUGUAUAAUAUAUAAUUACAUAAUAUAUGUAAUGUAUAAUAUAUAGUUACAUAUAUAAUUAAAUGUAAUAGAUAUAGUACACAAUAUAUAAUAUAUGCAAUAUAUAUUACAUUUCAUAAAAUAUAUAAUACAUAUAAUCGAUUAUGAAUCGAUUAUAUGUAUUAUAAAAUAUAUGAUACACAUAAUCGAUUAUGUGUAUUAUAAAAUAUAUGAUACACAUAAUCGAUUAUAUGUAUUAUAAAAUAUAUGAUACAUAUAAUCGAUUAUAUGUAUUAUAAAAUAUAUGAUACAUAUAAUCGAUUAUAUGUAUUAUAAAAUAUAUGAUACAUGUAAUCGAUUAUAUGUAUUAUAAAAUAUGUAAUACAUGUAAUCGAUUAUAUGUAUUACAUAUUACAUAUAUAAUAGAUGUAUUACAUAAUAUAUAAUAGAUUUGCUAAUGUAGCAAAUGCAAUAUGAAACUGUCAAGUUAGGAGAAAUUGGGAGAAAUUGUCUGAAGGAGUGACACUUAUCUUUCACAUCUGGAAUCUAGUACAAUACAUUGCUUUAUUCUUGUAAAUAUGUUAGUCAAACACACGUUUUGGGUAUUAAUGUUUAUUCUCUACAGUGUAAAAAGAGAAUGCAGGGCUGCUAACAGAUUCCAGUAUAAAAGAUUGAUAAUAGAGUCUUAACAAACUGCUGGGCUGAUGUGCCACUCUAACUUUAUAAGCCUAAAUUUCCCUGAAAAAAAAUUUAAGUAACGGUAUAAAACUUCAAGUGCCACUUUGUCAUUGUUGUUGGUUUUAAUUAUUACAGCAAUCAGUAGCCCUCAAGCUAUUUCCCCCAUCUUCCUGCAGCUGUCCAGAAUAGCCAUCUGUUCUUGCAGGUGGGCCAAAUUCUAAUCUCUAGUAAGGCUUCCACCCGGACUGGUGUGCUUACCUACCAUUUCUUUCUUAGGAGCCCGCUUUGAAAUGGAAUCCUUUUCUAAACAGAAGUUCCAUACACUGAGUUUUAUCUAUUUAUAAUUUGAAAGUGUGGGACUGACAACUUUGAACUUAGAUGACAUUAAAUUGUUUGGAGGGAGAGGGCAAAUUUUAAGGGCAUUUACUUGAUGAUUUGGAAAGAAAGCCCAAACAGAUUCUUUUGGAGUGUUAAAUUUGGGAUAUUACUGUUUCAUACUCAUUACCUUUUACCAACAGUCGGAUGGGAAAAAUGUGUAUGUGGGUUUAAAAUAAAUUCUGUUAGUAUAUGGUGCUAUUCUACUGUAUCCAAGGAUACCUUCAAGUAAUAGAAUUACUUCUUUGCUCUGGCAUUUUGCUUAUAGUUCCUCCAAUGUUAUUGCCUCACAGCUCUGGUUUCCAUGGGAGGAGACAAUAUGUUUUUCAUAUAUAAAAAUCUGGUUUAUUCAUCUCAAGCCAUUAGUACCUAUGUCAAAACUUCUCAUUAUUAGUAAAUUUCAUUUUAUGUAUGAAUCAUACAGGGGAAGGCCAUUCCAAUUGAUUUGUCAAUGAAUGGGGAAAGACUGCUACUUGGUAAUAAUAUAUAAGACAAUGAUUAUGUUAUUUAGAAACGUACAGAACCAAAGAGGUCUAUUAUUCUAGCCUGCAUUUUCCUUUGUGAAUGAGCCUCAGCAUUUGAAUAUGCUGAGAGUAUUGUCUUCAGGUGUUACUUGCUGGCAUGUCGUUCUGUUGUGAUGUUUCUGCUAUCUGAUGUAUGCAUGUUCGUAUACUGUCUGAGUAGAUUUUAACUUCCUUGAAAAUAGAUCUGUGUCUUCUGUGAAAUGAUAGUUGACUUAACUUCUCUUUCUUUUUUAGUUUUUCCAACAUUAAAUAAGGCACAUGGGAAUUAAAGAAGCUUCCUCUCAUUUUAAAAAGUCUAUUGCUUAGACAAGUUGCAGAAUUUGUGCGGAAUAAAGCUACUACAAAAUUUGUGCAGCAAUGGAUAGCCUGUAAAGCAGGGGUCCCAGUACCUGGGCUACGGAUCACUAGUGGUCUGUUGGCUGUUAGGAACUGCUGCACAGCAGGAGGUAAGUGGAGGUGAGCGAGCAUUACCACUUGAGCUCCGCCUCCUGUCAUAUCAGCAGUGGCAUGAGAUUCUCACAGAAGCGUGAACCCUAUUGUGAACUGCGCAUGCCAGGGAUCUAGGUCUCUUGCCCAAAGAGAAUCUAAUGCAUGAUGAUCUGUCACUGUCUCCCAUCACCCCCAGAUAGGACCAUCUAGUUUUCCUGCAGGAAAACAAGCUCAGGGCUCCCACAGAUUCUAUAUUAUGGUGAGUUGUAAAAUUAUUUCAUUAUUACAGUGUACUAAUAAUAGAAAUAAAGUGUACAAUACAUGCAGUGCACUUCAGUCUUCCCAACCCCCUGCCUGCCGCCAGUCCAUGGAAAAAUUGUCUUCCACGAAACCAGUCCCUGGUGCCCAAAAGGUUGGGGACCACUGUUGUAGAGCUUUAUAGUAUGAAUGUACAUAUUAAUAAUUUAUUUAAAUUCUUGAAACAAAUGAUAAAAUAUACAUAUAUUUUCCUUUCAUCAGGAGUUCAUUUAAGUUUUUAUCACCUGGGUUCUUCUUAACAUGAAUGGGAGCAAUAUGAAGUCAAUACAUGUACAUAACAUACAAGGGUGAUUGUGGCUCAGUUUUUUUCUUAUCUUUUUUACAGUUCAGAAAAAUGUUGGAGGUCCGAGGGGAUAGAGAUCUUUGCUGAAUUUCUGUCUUUCCUUUAAGAGGAGAACUUACAGGAGAAAAAAAGAUUUAACACUUUCCCUACUGUGAACUUUAACAAAAAUGAAGAUUUUGAUUUUGCUUAGAAUUCUUUCUUUUCAGGAACUUUCAAAGGAUAUUACCUCAACUUCUUGCAUAGCAGUACAGUGAUAAACACUUCUUUUAUCAUUUUCUUUUCUUUUUUUUCUUUUUCUUUCUUUCUUUCCUUUUUUUUUUUUUUUUUUUUGAGACGGAGUUUCACUCUUAUUGCCCAGACUGGAGUGCAAUGGUGUGAUCUUGACUCACUGCAACAUCUGCCUCCCAGGUUCAAGUGAUUCUCUUGCCUCAGCCUCCCAAGUAGCUAGGAUUACAGGUGUGCACCACCAUGCCCGGCUAAUUUUUUUACUUUUAGUAGAGACAGUGUUUCGCCAUGUUAGCCAGACUGGUCUUGAGCUCCUGACCUCAGAUGAUCCACCCACCUUGGCCUCCCAAAGUGCUGGGAUUACUGACAUGAGCCACCGCGUCCUGCCUCAUUUAUCGUUUUAAGUUUUUAUUUCUCUAGUCUUUGUUUCGACAAGCUUAUGUGGAUUCUUUUCUUUCUUUCUUUCUUUUUUUUUUUUUGAGACUGGGUCUUGCUCUGUUGCCCAGGCUGGAGUGCAAUGGCAGGAUCAUAGCUCACUGCAGCCCCGACCUCCUGGGCUGAAGUGAUCCUCCCAUCUCAGCCUCCCAAAUAGCAAGGACUACAGGCAUGUGCCAUCACACAUUUUUUAAUUUUUUGUAGAGACGGAGUCUCCCUUUGUUGCCCAGGCUGGUCUCGAACUCCUGGGCUCAAGUGAUCCUCCCAGAGUAAGUCUUAUUGCUAUGCCUUUAAGCAUAUACUGUUGGCUGAGGAAAUGCCUCAGACUUUUCUUGUAGGGAUCAAAAGUUAUAGUAUUGGUUAAAAAAAAUAGAGACAGAAUGUGUUUCUACAGUAUCUACAUAGUUCCUGCCUUCAAAGUGGCUAAUCUCAAAUGAUUCAUUUAACAACACCCAUCAAAUGUUUAUUGAGCACUUGUUAUGUGCCAGGUGUGCUGAGCCCAGUCCUCAAGCUCCACGAGUUUAUGGUUUAUAAAAAAGGCAUAUGUAAACAAACUGCAGUAUAGUAAAUGAGGGUUUCCAGAGAGGUGGGCCCAAGAGAUCAGGUGAGAGGGCUGGGCAGGGUGGCUCACACCUGUAAUCCCAGCACUUUGGGAGGUCAAAGUGGGUGGAUCACUGGAGGUCAGGAGUUUGAGACCAGCCUGGCCAACAUGGUGAAACCCCGUGUCUACUAAAAAUACAAAAAAAUCAGCCAGGCGUAGCGGUGGGCACCUGUAAUCCCAGCUACUUGGGAGGCUGAGGCAGGAGAAUUGCUUGAACCUGGGAAGCAGAGGUUGCAGUGAGCCGAGAUCGUGUCAUUGCACUCCAGCCUGGGCAACGAGAGUGAAACUCCAUCUCAAAAAAAAAUUUAUUUAAUUAAAAAAUAAAAAAAUAAGAGGGCAGGUGAGAGGAGGUGUGAUAAAAGAUGAAGCAGAUAAGGGAGGGGGGCAUUUAUUCUCAAGAAAUAUUAAUCAAACACUUGUUAUUUUCCAGGCACUGUUUAGGAUACUGGGGCUAUAGGAGUGAACAGAGCAGUGCUGCCUCCUUUGAGAGCUUCUAUUCAGUGUGGGAGACAGAUAUUUAUCAUCCUGCCCAGCACUCAUGCCUGUGUGUUAAUUAGGUAGGGGAGAGGGGGGAUCUGCAAGGAGGUGACAUUUGCAGAGGGGCCAGAGUGAAGUGAGGGGGUCAGGCACCAGGAGCAGCCCUGCUACAGUGUGCACUGCCUUCAUAUACUUCAAACUCCUCUUGAAAGAAAGGAAAUAACAUGUCAAAGUGAGGAAGAGAAACGGCAUAGUAUAAACAGAAAUAAGAUGAUAUGUCUGGGAUCUUGAUGCUUUAUGUCACUGUUAGUCCCCCAGCCUUCAUCAGUAAGGGCUGUUUCCCAAGCCUGGGUUGAGAUACUCUUCUAGGGGGAACAGCCUCUCUUCCCCCAACCACCUGUCGCCCUAGGUCAGCUGCAGCAUCCCUGCCGGGGACCAUGCAUAGCUGGGCCAUCAGGAAGCCAAUGGUGGGGGACAGCUGCCUGGGGCAACACUGGGCCAUAGAUAAGUUCCCAGACCCAAGACCCGACCCCAGCCCCUCCUAGACAGCAGCCCGCAGCCCCGUGGCUUCCCCCCGCCCGCAGGAGAAGCCACACAAGUCUUAACAAAGGGGAGUCCCCGUGUGGAAAGAACAAAUCCGACCUAAAAUUAAACCUGGAGUUUUAAUAUAAAGAAAUGCUCAUGAUUAGGUGUUUACAGCACCUAAUCUUCAACAAUUAAAAAGAAAAAUGUGUGGGUGGGGUAAAAAAUAGCAAUACCCACACUCUGAAGUUUUGGAGAAAAACAGGAAACUAGUCUUUUUUAACCAGUGAUGCCCAAAACUGGUUAUUGCAAAGAGGGUUGUUUUUCUAAUGCAGUGUGGUCAGCGCAGCUGCACCCGAAGUAGAAUUCUGCUCAUGAUGCAGCCGUCUGUGGAUUUCUUUAGCUGACAAACCUAUAGACAGGCAGGCAUAAUUAUCAGUUCUAACCUGGUCAUUAUGGCCGGAUGGUGCUUGGAAAACAAUUUGCACAAGUCCUGAAACCCCGUGAGAACAUACAAAAUAAGAGCAUUUGGCGAAUAUGCAGUUAUUUCCGGGAGUUGUGAAUGACUUAGAUCUAGGGGCUAUACAAUAGCUUAUUGUAGAAGAACUGUUUGAAUUCUCUUUUUAUUUGGAUUUUUUUUUAAGUUGACAGACAACAUCUGAUGGCAAAUGACUUUUUUUUUUUUUCUAAUUUGCUCAUGAACUCAAGCUUCACUUUCUAACAGCGUUUUAGAUGUUUCUACCUUUUUAUUUUUGGCAUUCGCUGGUUGGUGACAGUGAAGUCAUGAUUUUAAAAUUGGGGUUACAGAGAUGUUGUUUCCUGGCCACAGAGUCUCACAAAUGCACUAUCACCACUACGUUUCUGAACAACAUGAGAAAAAUGAUCACAGAGGAGACCAUUUGGGCAACACCUGACUAGAUUUUUGUCCUUUUGAAUAAUGUAGAAUGCUUCAGAACCCACUUGAAGUACAGUAAUCCCCUUUAUCUGCAUUGUACCUUACACGGAAGUCCAGGUUGGUCUCGGACCAGUCACUGAGGUUUCCCCUCCACUUCCUGCUGUGGGCUCAGUGUCUUUGGGGAGCCCCUGCUAACCAGAAGUCUCCCUCACAGGUCAUUUCUUUGUGUCAUCUUUCUAAGGAUAAAAAGGGGCAUUAGACUUUUGAAAGUUGAGUGAUAUAACCUAGAUUUCAUUGCUGAUUGCAUUUUAUGGUCUCCAAGCCAAGCAUUUGGUUUGUGCAUUGAAGGCUUUACGCUUGUCUGUUUGUAUCAGACUUUACAGUUAUCUCUUUAAUAAGUAAAUUACUCACGCUUCUCUUUUGUGAAGCUUGAUUUCAGUGCUUGAUCCAGGCAGUGUGCCUGGGCUUAGCAAGGCCCCCUCUCCAGCUGACUGCUGAGGCAGUUCCAAAAAAGGUAGUCAUUACUGCUAUUGAUUUCUGUAGCACAUCGGUCAUGUUAGAAUUAUUUGCAGUGAGAGGGGAGUCAACUCCUUGCAUAUGACUUUUAGUUUCACCACCAAUGUAUUGUACAUUGAAGUCUUCAGUAUCUUUGAGUCUUCAGUGUCUUGGGGGCAGUGACCCAAGCAAGUCAAAGGAGAUUCUUUUCACUUUUUUCUCUGGGAAUGGCUUGGGGAGAAUCCUGGAUAUUAAAGUGGUGCAGUAGGUGGAACUGGGAGACAUAAAUUCUCCUUUUCUUUUUUUUUUUAACCCCUUGCUGUCUGUUUUUUAGUGAAAAGCGAUGCAGUUACCUGCCAUUUCCCCCUUACCAGGAUGUGGUAAAAAGUAACGAGAGAAUGGUUGUCAAGCGUUGUCAAAUACUGAAGACAGAUAUUUUAUAAAGUGCCAGCUUUUACUGAAAACAAACACACCAAAAAACAACAAAACCAGCAAACAAGCAUAAUUUAUCAGAAGGUCUCAAAUUUCAGACACAUUAACAUCCUGGUGUUUCAGUUGGGAAAACAUAGCCCUGUGAGCUUGUGAUAAUGUUGAACUGGCAGUAAUAAGAAAUAAGUGAAAGAAUACUUUCACUUCUUAUAUAUGCCUCCACCAUAGUGUAUUUUUAAUAAGUUUGCAUACUGAGAUUUUGGAAAUCUGUGGAUACAAAUAUAAUUUUACACUUUCAUACCAGUAAAGCCUGAGUCCAACGUUGACACUCUUCCUUUUAAAUGGCUCACUUAAGCAUAUGAACAGAAGCACUGCAUAAAAAACUCAGUGGGGAGACUCAGGAAAACAGAUUCCUUUCUUAUUGUAGAUCCAUGAACAAAACCUAUCUCAGCAGAUAAUUCAGUAUAGUUGAGAGGUUCCCCAGAACUAAUUUUGGUUUCUACCACGUGGUUAUUAAUACAUUAAGUAUUUGCCCAUUAAAAUUAAAGGCUCCUCAAAUUCAUACUGUUUGUGCCCAUUUUGUUUUUGUUUGUGAUUUUUAUUAUAACACAAAGACAGUUUAAAACACACUGUACUCUUCUUCUUCUGUCCUUCCUAAUGAUAAGAUGGUGCUCUGGGGAUGACGGUUACUUGUACAGAAGGUUGUAGCGGAAGAGGCCAGUGUGGAAUGAUUAGUCCUUUCCCUGCUGUGCACACACAAAGAUUGGUCCUUCAUCCUCACAGUCAGCAUUUCUCAUGUGGCCUGGAGCUCAGUGGAGACUUCGCCUAUCAAGCUUGGGGUCAGCUUUUGCCUGUGUUCAAAAAAGUUGCUCUUGUGGGUGAACUUACCACGUGGGUGGUUCAUCUAUUGUAGCCCACAGACACUCCAUGUGACUGGGACCCUUAAUGAAGCGGGUUUCAUAAGCUCCCUCUUACCUACUUUCUUUGGAGCCAAUUCCCUUCUCUUUACCUUUUGGGAAGAAAACCAGCAUGGUGGUGAGAACUGAAAGUGAAGUUGCAGAUGACUAAGCCAAACUUUUUCUGCUUUUAGUUGAGGAAAAAAAGGACCAGAAAGAAGUUACUUAACGUUCCUUGCCCGGGUCAUGGAGUCAUUUGUGGUGGAGUGGACCUGAAAGCUGUGCCUGCUUUCAUUCUUUUUCCUACAUCCGGCCCAGUAGGACUUUUCCCUGGGGGAGAUUAUUGCUUUAAUACUGGGUGGCUGCGAGCAUUUCAGGAACGUGUGCAUGUUCCUGGGUUGUCAUUUGAUGCUUGGGGAGGAAUACAGCUGCUGUUUAUGGAAAAGCUUAAGAAGCAGGAUGUGGCAUUGGUGGCAGGGUUCACAUUCACAGAGGAGUUUGUGCAGUGCCUUCCCUGGAAAAUUUCAGUUACAUUCAGGUGAUACCAAGUUCAUCCCGUGCCCUUUCUGCCAGCCUCCUAAAGUUCGGCUGUCUUGAUUGGACAUCUUCAAUUAAAAAACAAAUGUCACACUUUGUAAUUCUGAAGAAUACUAUGGGUUUUUUUGUAGAAUUUCUCUUGGUUGAGCACGAUCUUUAGGAUGAAGUUUGAGUAAUACAAUUAGUCUAAAGGAUUUUUGUUAUAAUCACUUGCUUAAACAUCAGGAGCCUAGUGACAUGUACCAAAAAGUUAUUGCAGCAGAGUUACAAUGUUACCGGUUUUCUUAGCUCCAGCAUGGUUAGGCAUUUGGAGCCAGAUAAGUCUUUGUUGUGGGCGACUAUCCUGUGCAUUGUAGAAUACUUACCAGCAUCCCUGGCCUCUACCCACCAGGGUACAAUAGCAUACCCCUUCCCACUCCCAGUCUUGGCAACCAGAAAGAACUCCCAGACAUUGCCUAGUGUCUCUUAAGGGGGCAGAAUCACCCUAAUUGAGAACUACCACAGGCUAACAAUAAAUCUGAGGGGGAUGGCACAGCCACCAGCCUGAACCGGGUUUUUAUGAACAACACAGAGCUUGAAUUUAAGAAACCAGAGUAAGAAACAAAGACUGAGAACAUUAUGUGACUAAACAGUGAAUAUUCCCAGUCAGUGACAGAGUGAAUGGCAACCCCAACCAGGGAAUUCCCCGGUUGCCUUGUGGUAGGAAUUCCCUUCUCUUCCUCAAUUCUCUUGCCCUCAAUUCUAGGACACUCCCUUUUCAAAGGCUGCUCUAGCUUCUGAUUCACUUAUUUUCCCUGCCCUCUUUUCUUUUCCAUUCUUCUGCCAUCUCUGCUGCUACCAAUGCCUGGACCACCACUGCUGCCCUGACAAAAGACAAGAGCCACUGAGAUUCUUCCUACUGAUGCCCCUGGCCCAUCUGUGUCUUGCUAUUCUUACUUUGUUAUUUACCUCUUAGAGUUUCACCUAGACUUUUACGGUCCUUGUAGGAAAAGGCAGUUUCAUAUCCUAUUGACUCAAUUUCUCAGUGUGACUAUUUGACAAGAAGCUAUGCCAUCUAAGGUGGGUAGGUUCUAUGUUGCUCUUAUUACAUUGCCUUAGGCGAAUUCUAAAUCAGGUUAUACAGGCUUUUGAAGGGUGGCCUUGCAUGCCAACCAGUAUUUAUGACACUGGUUUUAGAGGGAAACACAUUCCAAAUUUCAAAUAGUAAGCUUAAAAGUGAACUGUUAGAGUAUGAUUCAUUUUAAGUAGGAACUAUUCUGGGAGCCGGAAGAACAGGUGCUAGCACCUGUUACAAGUGAAUUCUUAUCGAAACCACAGGGAGACCCUUUGGGUAGCCAGCUUAGAGUCCCUUCUCUACUGGGAGUGUAACUUCUCACACUAAGCCCCAGGCUCAGAGGGCAGACAAGCUGGAUUAGCUAGGGUUUGCUUCUCUGAUGUGGAAAAAAAAAUAGAUAUCUGGUAAUUUCCUUGGAUUCCUUUUGGACAUGAUCUUGUGUACAAAUCUGUGCCAAAUGAACUUAAUCUGCCAAGAGAGGAAAAGAAAAAUACCUUAAUCUAUGGAUCUAGCUACCAACUGAAGGAAGUCAAUAAGAAAAUAACUGGAAUCUUAGCAGGUUCUAGAAAAAGUAAGAAAAGAGGUAUAUGUUGUACAAGUAUGCAAUUAAACUAAGAGAAGUUUGGAGUAAUUAAAAGAUAAGCACAAAAAUACCUCACUUUCUACAUCAAAUGACAAAUAUUUAUAUCAAAUUUUUCAAAGAUAGGAAUGUUUAUCAUUUUAGACUAGGAAAGAUACAACACAGAAGACUCUAAUACUCAGAGGGUUUUCCAGUUCUGAGUAUCUUAUGUAUUUUUCCCCUGUUACUCUAAAUUUGUCAAACUGCACAAAUUGAUUCAUUAGAUUGAGUGUUAAGUCUACCUAAACUAGAAUGUGAUAGUGAUGGGCCAGUGACUUCUUUGGAGAAAUCUCUAAAACAUCUAUGCUGAUGAGUUUUGAAACUGGGUUCAGGGUGUCCUGAGACAUCUGGGAGUUGUUGAAAUAAAGUAUAUCUGUGGUGGAUUUAAGAAUUACUCUAUAUUUCAGGUCAUGAUAGGAGGGAUACUUAGCUCCCAAGUUUUAAAGAAUUUAGAAGAGUGCUGCCUUUCUCAAAUAUUGUUAUGUAAUUGAUUAUUCAGCAUGCCUUUUGUUAUGGGGUCCACACAGUAACAAUCUAUUUUCAGUGUCUGACCUUCACUAGCCCCUGAGCUCCAUGAAGACAAGAAUCAUGGCUUAUGGGAAUGCACAAUUGUUUGUUGAAUAAAUAAUUGAAUAAAUGAGAGAAAAAAAGAGUUUAUUGUGAGCAUUUUAUUAAAAAAAGCGAAAUGCUACUUCUUGAUAGAAAGAUUAAAUAAAGUCAUUUCCCAAUAAUAAAGUUAAAACAAAAUUUAAAAUAAUAUAAUGGACUGAAGUUUUAAGUUUGGUGGGAAAUCUGUGGCUUUAAGAAGGAAGAAAUAGACUAUACUUUUUAAAGAUAGAAAGCAUGGCAUGCCCUCCAAAAUUAACCUAGUGGAACAUGGUGUGUAAAGUCUCCCAAACCCAUCAAUUUUAGCCUUACUUUAUAGUAAUAAACACUUUUUAUUGCCAAAGUAAAUUAGGACAAUGAUCUGGGUAAAAUAAUGCUCUUGAGCUGGAUAAGAAAGACUUUGAUUUUCUUGCCAAAUUUAAAGCAAUGACCUUCGUUCUAAGUGUGAAAGCAGCAUAUCAUUGUUGUAUAAAGACAUGAGUGAACCCCACUGAAACUCUUCCACCGUGAGGUUCUGUCAUACCAGCUCAAAUAGUGAGUAAUCAGGAAUGGUUCAAUACAUUAAACAUUCUUUUGGCAUGGUGAUCCUUUUGUCAGGUCAGAAUCAUUAUGACUAGAACUGAAAAUUGAGUGCCAGUCAUGGCAGGAUAUUUAGAUUUCUUCAACCCAUGUAUCUUUUUACAUUGCCACUAUGUCUAUUUUCAAGAGGGAUGGUUCAGACUCAGGCUUAAAGGAUUAAAAAACUCUCUCCAGCACUUACAGUGAGGCUGUAGACAAGUUCCUGAGCCUUUCGGGGCCUCAAGUCCUUUGUAAGCUAGGGUAAUAAUUGUACCUGCCUCAUAAAAGAUUAAAUGGGAAAAUACUCAGUAAAUGUUGCUUUCUUUUAUUUUUCUCUGUGAUGAUUGUUUCAAACUCCAUUACCGUUUCUAGAUCUUUCAUUUCCUUAAGGUUUUCAGUAGUCAGCCCAAACUUUUAACAUUCCUCUUUGUGGAAAUCAUAGCAGCCUAAAGAGUCUAGUUUGCCAAAACUAUUUGCUACAUCUUAUAGAGAAAUUAAAUCAUGCUUGGGGUGUACCUGUGUGUCUGUAUAUAAAAGAGCCUCAACCCUGAGUCUUACCACAGUGAAAGCAGGUGGACCCCACUCUUGGCUAUGAGCCAAAUCCUAUUACUAGGCCUUAUUGAUUCCAGGCUGGCUACAGUUGCUUCCUCUUGUUGUUGCUUUUCCUUCUCACCUCUUAAGGGAGUUGGAAAACUCUAAAUUCAACUUAUGAAAGAAUAUGAAAGUGCUUCUAUUAUUUGUAUAUUUCCCAGAAACUAACCAUCUAGAAGUCAUUUCCUAAGUUAUAAAGAAACACUUUUUUUCCUGAAUUUUUCAUCACAUGAAUAAAACUGGGUUUUCCAUUAUGAUCAUACAACACAAACCACCAGACUGUAAAACUAACAUUUUUCAGUUGGGUUUCUUGCUUACUAUUUUCAAAGUGACUGUUUUCUUGUCCUGCGACAGUGUUCAGGGUGAGAACCACGGUGAGGUAUGACCCCAGAUGGAGCAGGAUGAAUUAGUCAUUAUGUGCUAGGAGCGUGAGCAGUCAGUGAAUUCUUUCAGGGUGCUUCUUCAGAAAUUGUCUAGGUGGACUUACUGAUAACUUAUAAUUGUCAGGCUUAGGAAUUCCCUCCCAUCUAGAUGUCUGAAUAAAAUGUUUAAAAGUUUCUCAGAGUAGUUUGGGCAGCCUCUUUGUCAUAAUCAUUUUCUUUCUUGCACAAUUUAAACUUAGUUUUGAUAUUUUUCAGUGGAAGUUGUUAUUAUUGCAUUGAUUUUAAAUCUGUUUCACAAUAAGAGAUUUAAGUGGAUGAUCUCUAAAGCUUUGUUCAGCUUGAAAAUUAUAUGGUCAAAGUUUAUCUUUUAGUAGUUUCAUUUUCAAGAUUUCCCCACAGUGUUAUGCGAUUCCUUAUUGAUUUAUUCGACAGAACAGCAGCAUAUUCCUUCAAUUAAAGACUCCCCAAAUCAUUAUAUCAUCAUUAGUAGUCAAUUGCUGAGAAUUUGAACUUUUAUAUUAACACAAUCAAGUCAUAAUUAUCUCUCCACUGUGGCCAAAAUUUAAUCCAGUAAAAUAUUGUUAGGACAUUGUAUUUUUUUUCAGGGCCAUAGCUGUUAAAGGUCUCUCAACUAGAAAAAUUUAAAUAUGCUCCAAUCCCUUCCAUCUUGAAAACAAGCAAACAAUAAAACCAAUAAUCCUGAUGGCUUUUCUAGCUACUACUUUACCUGUCCCAACUGCUUCACAGUUUCGACCACCUGCUUUCACGAGGAACAUUUAUAACCUCUUAAUUUUGAAAUUCAGUGACAUCUUUUGGGUCUUUGACUUAUUUGACCUGAUUUGUGUCUGACUCUGUUUAUCAUUUAAUUUUUUCGCCACUUGGUUCUGUGAUGCUGUGGCUUAGUAGGCCUGUCUCUGUUCUCAGCCCCUUUGCACACUUCCUAGUCUUUGAGGCUUUUCCCAAAGUUCAACCCUUAAGCCACUCUCUGUAGCUUUUCAGACUGUUUUACAGAAACCCACUCUAGGCCAGGCGUGGUGGCUCAUACCUGUAGUCCCAGCACUUAGGGAGGCCAAGGCAAUCAGAUCACUUGAGCCCAGGAGUUUGAGACCAGCCUGGGCAACAUAGUGAAACCCUGUCUCUACAAAAAAAUACAAAAAACAUUAGCCAGGUGUGGCAGCACACACCUGUGGUCCCAGCUGCUCAGGAGGCUGAGGUGGGAGGAUGGCUUAAGCCUGGGAGGUCAAGGCUGCAAUGAGCCUUGAUCGUGCCACUGCACUGCAGCCUGGGUGAUAGAGCAAGACCUUGUCUCAAAAAAAAAAAAAAAUAAAUAAAUAAAGAAUCACUCUAGCUGCUAAUGAUGCUAAUAGUCUUCAAUACUAGUUUUUCAGUUCACAUAUUCCCAUGGAUUCUACAUCUAUGUAUCCAAAUGUCUACUUGGACAUUUCUACCCAGUUGUUUCUAAGGCACCUCAAACUUAGUUUGCUCUAAAACCGAAUAUAUUUCCUUUCAGCUUGGUUUUCCUCUUUUCCGCCUCACAAAUGUCUACUGAUUACUGAAGAUCCACUGCAAGUGUCUCCACUGUCAGAGCUUCCUUAAUAACUCCUCCUCUCUUUCCUAUGGACUCUGUGGUAAUUUGUACUACAGCACUUUUCAUACUUCCUCCAAGCCCGGUAUUCUCUAAGAUCAUAAAACACAUUUGUGUACCUUUGCAUACAGCCCAGUGCCUGGUGUGUGAUAGGUGCAUGGUAAAUGAUUGUUGAAUAGGUUAACAGAUGACAUAAAUAGCAAAUUAUAGAUAUUGAAAUAGGAAAAAAUAGAUUUCACCAGGUAGAAAAGUGUAUAAGUGGUUAGAUAUUAAAAAGAUACUUUUUAGAGUGUUACAGAAAAUAAAACAAUCAGGCUUAGUGAUUAGAUGUAGCCUCUGGGACCUCAGAAGUGAAGAGAAGCCUCUAGUUCCUUUCAUAGACUUGGGGUUGAACUGGUGCUUUCACUUGAUUUAAAUAGAGAUCAGUUCAUGGAAUGGCAGCAGCAGUUAUUUGGGUGACUUUUCCAGCUAUUUCAAAAGCAUCAGAAUGGACAGAGCAGAGCCCAACUAUUUGUUUCAGAUUUUUUUUUUUUUGAGACAGUGUUUGGAUCUGUUGCCCAGGCUGGAGUGCAGUGGCACAAUCACAGCUCACUGCAAUCUUAACUUCCCAGAUGCAAGCAAUCCUCCCACCUCAGCCACCUGAGUAUCUGGGACUGCAGGUGCACCAUGCUCCAGUUGAAUUUUUUUUUAAUUUUUAUUUUUAGAGACAGAGUCUCACUAUGUUGCUCAGGCUGGUCUUGAACUCCUGGGCUCAGACAAUCUUCCCACCUUGGCUUCCCAAAGUGCUGAGAUUACAGAUGUGAGCUACCAUGCCCAGCCUUUAGGAAAAUAUUCAGGUGCAAUUCUUUCCUAAACAUACUUCCUCCCUAUUUCUUCUACACUUCCAAAUACAGCUGUGUGUGUCAGGAAAAGAGGAUAUGAAUGUUUUCAUUUACUUAAGCAGUAAAAAAUAAUGGUUUCAUUUACAGAAGUGAUACCUUCCCCCAUCCCACAUCCAUAGAUAAGACUGUAUUUGUGUGCUAAUCAUACCACUUUAAGUUAUCUCUAAAUCCACUAAUAUUAAGUUCAUUCUUGGUGCAGUAGCUUCAUCACAGUUCAUUGAUGGUAACAUUAGAAAAAAGUUUGCUAUUGGAAUCCUUAUGUUGUUAGGAUUAGCCUCUAACUAAAUGGAACAGGUAUCUGGUUACCAUGGGAUAAUCCGUUGUUAAUGUUAAAUAUAAGAAGUCUUAGCAGUGAAGACUGAUUUGUGACAGUCCUAUAUUUAGGAUUAAGUUCUCUGCACUGUGAUGCUGAACCAUUGCAGAAUUAUGUUAUAUAACUGUGUUUCCUUUUGGCUUUCAUAAAAAUAAGAAACAUGUUUCCUGAGGUCAUCUUACAUUGAGCAAAAAUGUUAAAUACAUGAAUAAAAAUUCCACUUAGCUUUUUUUUAAUAUUAGUAGACUUCAUGUAGAUUUGUAGUCUUCAUAUAUUUUGGAGUCUUAUACUGGUUCAGUAGUCUUUUAUGAAGAACAACAAACAAAACAUCCUGUUUUUAUAAUGUUCAGCACAAAUCCCAGUGGAAUUAUUACAGAAAUAGCUGAAGUUCUUCCUAUAUCAGUUAGCAGUUGUUUAAUUUUCAUUAUUUAUUGUUACUCUUCAAAGUCAUUUUUCGAAGUGUGACUAUAACAGAAUUGAUUUUGUCAUCAGGCACCGAAGUCCUGCUAAGUGUUAAUUGCCCAGGGUUUUUAUAAGGAGUUUGGAGAUAACUCAAGUCCCACUACCAUAGCAGCAGUGACCAUUUUAAAUCGCAAAUAUGUGUAAAACUCUUAAACUCUUUUUCGUCUUUUUUUUUUCUAACAUUUCAUGGCUUCAUAUUUCAGAGACUUAGUGGGAUUACUUUAAGUGUUUGCUUAUAUUAAAAUAAGGGAAAACCGAAUAGAAAAGAUGUUUUUAAAGGGUUGUAAUAUGGCUUUAGGACUGGUGAAAGAGCCAGAACGAUGAUUUGGAAGCUGAAAAUAGCUCUAUGUUUUAUGCAAUCAAGUAAAACUCUGUACCUUGGCAUUCCCCGCACCAGAUUAGUGAGGAAUUGGAAGUGAUUCCACCCCCAACAUGCCAUUAUGGAUGACACGCUGGGCUAUGACAAACUGCUGGCUUAGUGGAGCAUGUGCUGCUGGGAGUAUAACCCUGAGGUACAGGGUGGAUUAGAGUUGAGUGAUCUCAACUCAUAUUCAUUUCCUCUGAAAGGAAAACUGACCAGUCCUCUCUGUUCUAAUGAGCAUGUUUACAGCAUGGCUUCUCAAAGUGGGGCCAGUCGCUUCAGGGGCAGAAGUGCACCAUAUUUCUGUUUGGUGCCAGCUUUACCUGCGUAGCCUUCACAGCACCUCAUCCUGGUCCUUAAGAAUUGCAGAUUAAGACCACAGAACAGAGGGAGAUGGAUAUUUCUUUUACACUCUUACAGGUUUUUUUUUCCUUAGUUUGUUUUUGAUGUGUUGUUUUGCAAAACGCUGUGAAAUAAGUGAGGACAUAAGAUGAUUACUGAACUAUUUCUGUUGAGCAAGUGGGUAAACCUCUCCUGGUAGAAGAAUCAGAACCUCAUCAGCCCAAGAGGCUGAGUCAUCUUUGUGACUGAGAGGUUCAUGCUUCACCUUAAGUCCUUGGUACCUAAAAUGGGACUGUAUGAUGUGCCCUGUGAAAUCAAUAAAACUGUCAGGUUAUAAUUAACGUGUGGUGCUACUCUAAUUAAACAGAAUUGAUGGGAAAUAUCUGGGAGUCUAGUAGCAAUGGAACAAUGAUGUUUGCAUUUAAAUGAUCUUAAGUACUCCUUAGACUUAAUGCCCUAUUAAGGGGACCGGGAGAAUGUCACAUCUCACUUAGCUGUAUUGUGUUAGACAGUGGCCGCUGGCCGGGAAGGACCAGAGUGCAUUAAGCUUGCGUUGUGGUGUCUGCCUUUGCAGACAGAAGAUUUGGGAAUGUAUAUUCUUUUCUUUUUUCUUUUUUUUUUUCUUCAAAGGAAAUUAAAUCACAGCCCUGACAGGAGAGGGUAAAAUCUCUGAGAAGACCUCCCCAGUGCUUGGAAUUUACAGACUCUACCACGUCCCAGUUUGCUAUUGUCCUAAGGCAACACACUCCCCUGCCGCUCUCAGGCGUCUUUGGCGGCUGGCCAGCCUCCCAGGGCCUCUGGCUUUGAUGUGUGGUGCAGGCUGUCCUCAGGCCAGGCUGUUGUUGCCGUGGCCUGGACUUCGCUCACACUGGAUGCCAGGAGGGAUGUCCUGUCUGCAAUAUACAUUUCGACAGCCUGACAGUCCUAGUGAUCGUCCUGCGGCAGGGGGAGCCUGCCUUUGUCUCAGCCACAAGUGGCUGUCCCCAGUCGCUUAGCUUUGCUGUGCUCUCUUUUGGUGUCUGCGGAAGACGAGUUUGCACCCAGCUUGUUGUCCGGGGGAGGGCCUCUCUGCCUGGGGAAGACAGCAGCUCUGCCAGGGCGCUGUCAAUCUGAGGAGCCUCCUUGGCAGGGCUCUGGGGAACCGACCCGGCGAGUUGAACAGCUUCCUCUGGGGACAUUGCAUCGACCUUCAUUUGAUUUAAGCCUGGCAGCCUGGUGGAGCCUUUGAAUUUUUUAAAAGACCAUAGUAAUCAGAUCUACUUGAAAAAUUAAGUGAAUUGAUUUGGUUGGAAUGCUCUUUUACCGAUGCUUUAACAUACAGCCACUAGAUUCCCAGAAGUUGUGCAUGAGUUCCUGUGAGGAGAGUUGGCAUCUUGGAAAUCAAAGACGGUUGUGAUGCAGUUUUUUGAUAUGAGGAUAACAGGAAGCGUCAGGACAAUCAUGCCCAUAAGAACUCUAAACUGUUCAGAUCAUUUUAUCUUAGUGAAACUGGCAAUUGAACUUUGCUCUAGUUGAUGGGCAAAAUUUCUCCUAGACUAUUCAUCAUCCCAAUUUCAUCCUAGUUGAAAAUUUUCAAAUGCCAUAAGAAAUCUUUAUAGAUUUGCACUUAGCUUUUGGAUGGACGUUUCUACAAUGGAGAGAACUGUGUUAUAGCCCUGGUCCAAGGACAUUACUAGCUAAUGCCCAUCGACUGUGGUGUGCGUGUGGAAGGUUCCAAAGAGAAGGAGCAAUCAGCAAGUUUGCAGACACCCUGGAACAUGGAAGCAACCAAGCUUUAAGAAGCACAGCUUUGGAGACACUCCAUGAGUCUGCACUGCUUUCAGGGGAACUAGCACUUAAGACCUUGUGUAACAAAAUGGACACUGGGGACACAGCUCUAGGACAAAAAGCUACCUCAAGGUCUGGAGAAACUGAUAAAGCAUCAGGUAGAUGGAGACAGGAACAAUCAGCUGUUAUUAAGAUGAGCACUUUUGGCAGUCAUGAAGGACAGCGGCAACCACAAAUAGAGCCUGAGCAAAUCGGAAACACAGCAUCAGCACAACUGUUUGGUUCUGGGAAACUGGCCUCCCCUAGUGAAGUGGUGCAGCAAGUCGCAGAGAAGCAAUAUCCACCGCAUCGUCCGAGUCCUUACUCAUGCCAACACUCACUCUCUUUCCCUCAGCACUCAUUGCCACAGGGGGUCAUGCACAGCACCAAGCCACAUCAGAGCCUCGAAGGUCCUCCGUGGCUUUUCCCUGGCCCUUUGCCAUCCGUUGCCUCUGAGGACUUAUUUCCUUUUCCUAUACAUGGCCACAGUGGUGGUUAUCCUAGAAAAAAGAUUUCAAGUCUGAACCCUGCUUAUAGCCAAUACUCCCAGAAAAGUAUUGAACAGGCAGAAGAGGCUCACAAGAAAGAGCACAAACCCAAAAAGCCUGGCAAGUACAUUUGCCCUUACUGCAGCAGAGCGUGUGCCAAACCUAGUGUACUGAAAAAACACAUCAGGUCCCAUACUGGGGAGCGGCCAUAUCCAUGUAUACCUUGUGGUUUCUCUUUCAAGACAAAGAGCAAUUUGUACAAGCACAGGAAGUCACAUGCCCAUGCAAUUAAGGCAGGAUUAGUACCUUUCACAGAGUCAGCUGUAUCUAAAUUGGACCUAGAGGCUGGUUUUAUUGAUGUAGAAGCAGAAAUACAUUCAGAUGGUGAACAGAGUACAGACACAGAUGAGGAGAGUUCUUUAUUUGCCGAGGCUUCUGACAAAAUGAGUCCUGGUCCACCCAUCCCACUGGACAUUGCCAGCAGAGGCGGCUAUCAUGGGUCAUUGGAAGAAUCAUUGGGAGGUCCAAUGAAGGUGCCGAUUUUGAUUAUCCCUAAAAGUGGGAUUCCUCUCCCUAAUGAAAGCUCUCAGUAUAUUGGCCCUGAUAUGCUACCAAAUCCAUCUUUAAAUACUAAGGCUGAUGAUUCGCACACAGUCAAACAGAAACUUGCACUAAGACUGUCAGAGAAAAAAGGACAAGAUUCUGAGCCAUCGCUCAACCUUCUGAGCCCGCACAGUAAAGGAAGCACUGAUUCUGGUUACUUUUCUCGCUCAGAAAGUGCUGAGCAGCAAAUAAGCCCUCCCAACACAAAUGCAAAGUCUUAUGAAGAAAUCAUCUUUGGAAAAUACUGUCGGCUUAGUCCGAGAAAUGCACUCAGUGUUACAACCACAAGUCAGGAGCGUGCCGCAAUGGGUAGGAAGGGCAUAAUGGAACCAUUACCUCACGUUAACACCAGGUUAGAUGUCAAGAUGUUUGAAGAUCCUGUUUCACAGCUGAUCCCAAGCAAGGGAGAUGUCGACCCCAGUCAAACGAGCAUGCUGAAAUCCACUAAGUUCAACAGUGAGUCCAGACAACCCCAGAUUAUUCCAUCAUCUAUCAGGAACGAAGGAAAACUUUAUCCAGCAAACUUCCAAGGCAGCAACCCGGUUCUCUUAGAAGCUCCUGUAGACUCUUCACCCCUUAUUAGAAGCAACUCAGUGCCAACUUCUUCAGCAACUAAUCUAACUAUUCCUCCUUCUUUGAGAGGAAGUCACUCAUUUGAUGAAAGGAUGACUGGUUCCGACGAUGUAUUCUAUCCAGGGACCGUGGGCAUACCCCCUCAGCGCAUGCUAAGAAGACAAGCGGCAUUUGAGCUGCCUUCGGUACAGGAGGGCCACGUGGAAGUCGAGCACCAUGGCAGGAUGUUGAAGGGUAUCAGCAGUUCAUCCCUGAAGGAAAAGAAAUUGUCUCCUGGGGACAGGGUUGGGUAUGACUAUGAUGUCUGUCGGAAACCCUAUAAGAAGUGGGAGGACUCUGAAACACCAAAGCAAAACUACAGGGACAUUUCCUGCUUGAGUUCUUUAAAGCAUGGUGGAGAAUAUUUCAUGGAUCCCGUGGUGCCAUUGCAGGGAGUACCAAGCAUGUUUGGAACUACCUGUGAAAACAGGAAACGCCGGAAAGAGAAGAGCGUAGGGGAUGAAGAGGACACGCCCAUGAUCUGCAGCAGCAUUGUAAGCACUCCUGUGGGCAUCAUGGCUUCCGAUUAUGACCCCAAACUGCAGAUGCAGGAAGGAGUCAGGAGUGGAUUUGCCAUGGCUGGACACGAAAACCUUUCUCAUGGUCACACGGAACGCUUUGACCCAUGUCGGCCCCAACUGCAGCCUGGAAGUCCAUCUCUUGUGUCAGAGGAGUCACCUUCAGCCAUUGAUUCAGACAAGAUGUCAGACCUAGGGGGCAGGAAACCUCCUGGAAAUGUGAUUUCUGUGAUUCAGCACACCAACUCACUGAGCCGACCCAAUUCAUUUGAAAGGUCUGAGUCAGCCGAACUUGUGGCUUGCACACAGGAUAAAGCCCCUUCCCCUUCAGAGACUUGUGACAGUGAGAUUUCAGAAGCCCCAGUGAGUCCUGAGUGGGCUCCACCUGGGGAUGGUGCAGAAAGUGGGGGGAAACCCUCUCCAUCUCAGCAGGUGCAGCAGCAGUCCUAUCACACACAGCCCAGGCUAGUUCGGCAACACAACAUCCAGGUUCCUGAGAUUCGAGUGACCGAGGAGCCUGAUAAACCUGAGAAGGAGAAGGAAGCCCAGAGCAAAGAGCCAGAGAAGCCUGUGGAAGAAUUUCAGUGGCCCCAGAGAAGUGAGACCCUUUCCCAGCUCCCCGCGGAGAAGUUGCCACCCAAAAAGAAGCGUCUGCGACUUGCAGAUAUGGAGCACUCCUCAGGGGAGUCCAGCUUUGAAUCCACAGGCACAGGCCUCUCCCGCAGCCCCAGCCAAGAAAGCAACUUGUCCCACAGCUCCAGUUUCUCCAUGUCUUUUGAAAGAGAAGAAACCAGUAAGCUUUCUGCACUUCCUAAGCAGGAUGAGUUUGGGAAGCAUUCAGAGUUUCUGACUGUCCCUGCUGGUUCAUACUCAUUGUCUGUCCCAGGCCAUCACCACCAGAAAGAGAUGCGACGCUGCUCAUCAGAGCAGAUGCCUUGUCCUCACCCAGCGGAAGUCCCAGAAGUUCGGAGCAAAUCAUUUGAUUAUGGGAAUCUGUCCCAUGCUCCUGUGUCGGGAGCAGCAGCCUCCACGGUAUCACCGUCCAGGGAGAGGAAGAAAUGCUUUCUGGUGCGGCAAGCUUCCUUCAGUGGCUCCCCAGAAAUCUCCCAGGGCGAGGUUGGCAUGGAUCAGAGCGUGAAGCAAGAGCAGCUGGAGCACCUGCAUGCUGGCCUCCGGUCCGGGUGGCACCAUGGCCCGCCUGCUGUGCUGCCUCCUCUUCAGCAAGAGGACCCAGGGAAGCAGGUGGCGGGUCCUUGUCCCCCGCUGAGCUCGGGGCCACUGCACCUGGCCCAGCCACAGAUCAUGCACAUGGACAGUCAGGAAUCUUUGAGAAAUCCCUUGAUCCAACCAACAUCCUAUAUGACAAGCAAGCACUUACCUGAACAGCCACACUUAUUUCCACAUCAAGAGACAAUUCCAUUUUCUCCAAUCCAGAAUGCCUUGUUUCAGUUUCAGUAUCCUACAGUUUGUAUGGUUCAUUUACCAGCUCAGCAGCCUCCCUGGUGGCAGGCACAUUUCCCACAUCCCUUUGCUCAGCACCCUCAGAAGAGCUAUGGCAAGCCCUCUUUUCAGACAGAAAUCCAUUCGAGCUAUCCCUUAGAGCAUGUGGCAGAGCACACUGGAAAGAAACCUGCUGAGUAUGCACACACGAAAGAGCAGACCUACCCAUGUUAUUCAGGAGCAUCAGGGCUACACCCAAAGAACCUUCUUCCAAAGUUUCCAUCAGACCAGAGCAGUAAGUCAACUGAAACGCCCUCUGAGCAGGUUCUUCAAGAAGAUUUUGCCUCGGCAAAUGCUGGGUCUUUGCAGUCCCUCCCAGGAACAGUGGUUCCUGUUCGGAUCCAGACGCACGUACCAUCCUAUGGAAGUGUCAUGUACACAAGCAUUUCUCAGAUACUUGGGCAGAAUAGCCCUGCCAUUGUCAUAUGCAAAGUCGAUGAGAAUAUGACCCAAAGGACACUGGUCACCAACGCAGCCAUGCAAGGGAUAGGAUUCAACAUUGCCCAGGUGCUGGGGCAGCAUGCGGGCUUGGAGAAGUACCCCAUUUGGAAAGCACCUCAGACUUUGCCCCUCGGCUUAGAAUCCUCCAUCCCCUUGUGUUUACCUUCCACCUCUGACAGCGUGGCCACCCUGGGAGGUAGCAAGCGAAUGCUUUCUCCAGCCAGUAGCUUGGAGCUCUUCAUGGAAACCAAGCAGCAGAAAAGGGUCAAAGAAGAAAAGAUGUACGGACAGAUUGUGGAGGAGCUUAGUGCUGUGGAGCUGACCAACUCAGACAUCAAAAAGGACCUCUCCCGCCCCCAGAAACCCCAGCUGGUUCGACAAGGAUGUGCUUCUGAGCCAAAAGAUGGCUUGCAGUCAGGGUCAUCUUCCUUCUCCUCGCUGUCGCCCUCCUCAUCUCAAGACUAUCCUUCUGUUAGCCCGUCUUCCAGGGAGCCAUUCCUGCCCAGCAAGGAGAUGCUUUCCGGUUCCCGGGCACCACUUCCGGGGCAGAAGUCCAGUGGGCCUUCUGAAAGCAAAGAAUCUUCAGAUGAAUUAGAUAUCGAUGAGACGGCAUCGGACAUGAGCAUGAGCCCACAGAGUUCUUCAUUACCAGCAGGAGAUGGUCAGCUGGAAGAGGAAGGGAAGGGCCACAAGCGGCCUGUUGGCAUGCUGGUCCGCAUGGCCUCUGCCCCCAGCGGGAACGUGGCAGACUCAACUCUUCUUCUCACGGACAUGGCAGAUUUCCAGCAGAUUCUUCAGUUCCCCAGUCUGCGGACAACAACUACUGUGAGUUGGUGCUUCUUGAAUUAUACAAAACCCAAUUAUGUGCAACAGGCCACCUUCAAAUCCUCGGUUUAUGCUUCAUGGUGCAUUAGUUCCUGUAAUCCAAACCCAUCAGGAUUGAACACCAAGACCACGCUGGCUCUUCUGAGGUCCAAGCAAAAAAUCACUGCAGAAAUUUAUACUCUGGCUGCUAUGCAUAGGCCUGGAACCGGCAAGCUUACAUCAUCAAGUGCUUGGAAGCAGUUUACUCAGAUGAAACCUGAUGCGUCCUUUUUAUUUGGCAGCAAACUAGAAAGGAAACUAGUGGGAAAUAUCUUAAAGGAAAGAGGGAAAGGAGAUAUUCAUGGAGAUAAAGAUAUUGGAUCCAAACAAACUGAGCCAAUCCGAAUUAAAAUAUUUGAAGGAGGGUACAAAUCGAAUGAAGAUUAUGUAUAUGUCAGAGGACGUGGCCGGGGAAAGUACAUUUGUGAAGAAUGUGGGAUUCGCUGUAAGAAGCCAAGCAUGCUCAAAAAACACAUCCGUACCCAUACUGAUGUUCGGCCUUAUGUAUGCAAGUUAUGUAACUUUGCCUUCAAAACGAAAGGAAACCUAACGAAGCAUAUGAAAUCUAAAGCACACAUGAAAAAAUGCCUGGAAUUGGGAGUCUCAAUGACAUCGGUGGAUGAUACAGAAACUGAGGAAGCAGAAAAUUUGGAAGAUUUGCACAAAGCAGCAGAGAAGCAUAGCAUGUCCAGCAUUUCAACUGAUCAUCAGUUCUCCGAUGCUGAGGAAUCAGAUGGUGAGGAUGGAGAUGAUAAUGAUGAUGAUGAUGAAGAUGAAGAUGACUUUGACGACCAGGGAGAUUUAACACCAAAAACAAGAUCAAGAAGCACCAGUCCUCAGCCUCCUAGAUUCUCCUCCUUGCCUGUGAAUGUUGGCGCCGUACCCCACGGGGUUCCUUCAGAUAGUUCCCUGGGACAUUCUUCGUUGAUCAGCUAUUUGGUUACUUUGCCAAGUAUUCGAGUUACUCAGCUUAUGACACCCAGUGAUUCAUGUGAAGAUACCCAGAUGACAGAAUACCAGAGGCUAUUCCAGAGCAAAAGUACGGACUCAGAACCAGACAAAGACAGAUUGGACAUACCUAGUUGUAUGGAUGAGGAGUGCAUGCUACCUUCAGAGCCAAGCUCCUCUCCCAGGGACUUCUCACCCUCAAGCCACCAUUCCUCUCCAGGAUAUGAUUCUUCACCCUGUCGAGAUAAUUCACCAAAGAGGUAUCUGAUACCCAAAGGAGAUUUAUCUCCCAGGAGACAUUUAUCACCUAGGAGAGAUCUGUCACCCAUGAGACAUCUUUCACCAAGAAAGGAAGCUGCAUUGAGAAGAGAGAUGUCCCAAAGAGAUGUUUCACCAAGAAGGCAUUUGUCUCCAAGGAGGCCAGUGUCUCCUGGGAAAGAUAUCACAGCAAGAAGAGACCUCUCUCCUAGAAGAGAGAGAAGAUACAUGACCACAAUAAGAGCGCCAUCUCCCAGAAGGGCUUUAUACCAUAACCCACCAUUGUCCAUGGGACAGUAUUUGCAAGCAGAGCCAAUUGUAUUGGGGCCUCCUAAUUUAAGAAGAGGAUUACCUCAGGUUCCUUACUUCAGUCUCUAUGGAGACCAAGAAGGUGCUUAUGAACAUCCAGGCUCCAGCCUUUUCCCUGAGGGUCCUAAUGACUAUGUCUUCAGUCAUCUUCCACUCCACUCUCAGCAACAAGUGCGAGCCCCUAUCCCCAUGGUGCCCGUUGGUGGGAUCCAGAUGGUUCACUCCAUGCCGCCAGCCCUUUCCAGUUUACAUCCUUCACCCACAUUGCCCCUGCCAAUGGAGGGCUUUGAGGAGAAGAAAGGCGCGUCAGGGGAGUCCUUCUCCAAGGACCCCUAUGUGCUUUCUAAGCAGCAUGAGAAGCGAGGUCCUCACGCUUUGCAGUCAUCUGGUCCACCUAGCACUCCCUCCUCUCCUCGGCUGUUGAUGAAACAGAGCACUUCGGAAGACAGCCUAAACGCAACAGAGCGGGAACAGGAGGAAAAUAUACAGACUUGUACAAAAGCCAUUGCCUCUCUCCGGAUUGCCACGGAAGAGGCAGCUCUGCUCGGGCCAGAUCAGCCAGCGCGGGUGCAGGAGCCCCACCAGAACCCCCUGGGAAGUGCACAUGUUAGCAUUAGACACUUUAGUAGACCUGAGCCAGGUCAGCCCUGUACCUCAGCCACCCACCCUGACUUGCAUGAUGGUGAAAAGGACAAUUUUGGUACAUCACAGACUCCAUUAGCUCACUCCACGUUUUACAGCAAGAGUUGUGUGGAUGACAAGCAGUUGGACUUUCACAGCAGCAAGGAAUUAUCUUCAAGCACAGAGGAAAGCAAAGAUCCUUCAUCAGAAAAGAGUCAGCUACAUUGAUCUAUGAUGCAUGGAGACUUUCAUUUCCACAUUUUCCCAUUUUUUUGUUUUUGUUUUUCUAGAAAUGGAGGUAAUCCAGUUUAUAGCAUGCCUGUCCUAAGUUACAGUAGUUUGCUAUUAUAUAUACUUUUGUUAUAUCAAAAGAAUUAGGUAAAUUAACAAGUCAUCAUGAGCCUGACCAAAACAAAAUUUGAAAUUAACCUAUUGGGUCUGGUACUUUUAAAAUUGUACAGAUGUUUGUGCCUUUUCUUUACUUUGCUUAUAUUCUUAUAAGCAUUUUUUAGCAGUAAUUUGUACAUAUUUUAGAAUUUGUGUAUCUGCUUUGUAAUAAAUGUAAUUUCUUUCCUUUUUUGGACACUUGGAUCUAAAUGAUGUAAAGCAAAACAGCAUCAAUAUAUAUGUGAGGUUGCACUAAAACAUAUUUUUAUAUGAUUAAAACUGAACAGCUUUUAUGUACAGCUCUGAUUCUGUAAUACUAAUAUUUAUUUACUUUGUUUCAUAAAUUGUACAUUUUUUCUUAAUGUUGUGGAUUGCUUUUCUAUGUGAAGCAUGGGAUUUACUGUUGCGUAACUAGAACAAAAAUGUACAUUGUAAACAAGAUAUUUAAACUAGAGUAUCUUAUUCUGCACUUAUGCAUUAGUUAAAAAAAGAUAAAGGAUGUAUCAGUCAGUUCUUAACUCUUGUAUAUUUUUUUGUCUCUUGUUUGCUGGAUUGACUAUAACUUAAGUGCUGAUUGUGAUUUUAAAAUGAUAGUACCGUAAAGCAUUAAAGUAAACAAUGUGCUAUUGUGAGUUUUUUCAAAGCUUUAUAAAUCAGUUAUAAAUAAUAUUAAAAGUAUUUGGUCUUAUGUGAACAUGUUGAUCUAUAUACUCAUCUAAAAAUAUGGGAAAACAUUCCACCCCAUGUAAAUAUGUACAAGUGCAUCACUGGUACAAUUUUAUGUAACUCAGUUGGACACUAGGUUGCCACAGACCUAUGCUAGGUGUCUUUAAAAAAUUAAGGUGACAAAGCACAUGGGACUGUGUAGAGCUUGGUUAUCGGCCGGCCCGGUGGCUUGGCAGGCAGUGCUGUGCGCUGCUCAUGGAGAAGACCUGGGCUUAGCAAUCUCCUUAGUUCUUGCUACACAGGAUGGUGACUGGAACUAAGGCUACACAGAGGGUCGCACUUGGACUCUGAGGGUUGGGUGUGGAAGGGGGAAAAGGAGAUGGAGACCUGCUCCCCAGCUCUUCCUGUCAGCCGGUUUACAUGGGAACAGGGUUAACAUCUGUGUUAGGGGAGGUCACCUUACCCUUUUUCAUAGGGGAAGAGUGUCACACUCCUGGCUAUCUCAGGGGGAAUGGGGAAAAGAAUCUUUCAAGGGCAAAGAACUCGUGGGAGGAUGUCUGUUGUAUGUAAUACUCACAAUGGCUUUUGGUUAGUGUUGAAGGUGGGAAGAGCAUUUGUAGGUCCAGAAGAGUGAAAGAGAGGGAGGGGUGCAGCAACAUGUGCACAGGCACGCACAUGUGUGCACGCACACAUACAAUCUGGGUUAUCUUUGUGCUAUAUAGUGGAUUAUAAUUCUGUGAAACCAAGUUUGUAUAUUGAAUUACAUUAAGGAGUGUUCUUUAAAAAGAGAAAUAAAUAUACAAUUACAUGCUU